CCAUUUUUGAUAGUUUUUUUUUUUUCUGCCUUUGCAAAGAAAAUUGAAGCAGUGGCAUUCCAUUUGUGGUGAAUUUGGAAUCUUAUGUUUUUCCAUGUUGGUAAAUUUAGCAUUCUUCUAGAAUGCUAUAACUUGGUAUCUAUUUAAACACACAUAUAAGCACAAACAAACAGAAACCCACACAAUACACCAUUAAGUUUGCAUGUCAACAUAUUUUUGAUUUGACUUUUGUCAGUCUCUGAAGAUUUUUGUUUUAAUCAAUAGGCUUUAUUUUGUAGAGCAGUUUUAGGUUUACAGCAAAAGUGAGAGGAAGGUACAGAUAUUUUUCCAUAAUAACCCCCAUCCCCACAUGUGCAGCUUCCCCCACUGUCAGCAUCGCCCACCAGGGUGGAGCAUUUGUUACAAUCAAUGAACCUACAUUGACAGAUCAUUCUCGCCCGAAGUUCAGAGUAUGUAUUAUGAUUCACUUUGGGUCAUGUACAUUCUACAGGUUUGGAAAAAUUUAUAAUGAAAUGUAUCUAUUAUCGUUGUGUUAUACAAAGCAAUUUCACUGCCCUGAAAACUCUCUGUGCUCUGCCUAUUCAACUUUUCCUCCUCCAAACCCCUGGCAAUUACUAAUCCUUUUACUGUCUCCAUAGUGUUAUACUUUCCAGAAUGUCAUAUAGUUGGAAUCAUACAGCAUAUAGCCUUUUCAGAUUUGGUUCUUCCACUCAGCAAUAUGUAUUCAUGUUUUCUCUAUGUCUUUUCAUAGCUUGAUGUUCUCUUUUUUUUAAUUUUUAGUGCUGGAUUAUUUUCCACUGUCUAGAUGUACCACAGUUUGUUUAACCAUUCACCUAUAAAAGGACAUCUUGGUUGCUUCCAAGUUUUGGCAAUUAUGAAUAAAGCUGCCAUUUUUUGUGGACCUGAGUUUUCAUUUUAUCUGAGUAAAUUCCAAGGAAUAUAUGAUUCCCAGAUCUGAUGUUAAGAGUGUGUUUAGUUUUGAAGGAAUCUGCCAAACUGUCUUUUAAAGUGGCUGUACCAUUUUGCAUUCCUACCAGCAAUGAGGGAGAGUUCCUAUUGCUCCACAUCCUCUACAGCAUUUGGUGUUGCCAGGGUUUUGUAUUUUGGCCGUUGUAAUAGGUGUGCAAUGGUGAAGACUGUCUUAAUAUGGCCAAAUCAGUGGUUCAGUUGGAAUUCUCUUGUCUCAGCAGAAUGGACCGAGGUAUGUUCUUGAUGUUCUGAGAUCGACAGUGAAUGUCUUCUGUGGUUGCUACUGAGGGAUAAGAGAAGAUGGCAGACCAGAGGAUGGAUUACCAGCAUUUCAUCUAAAACUAUAAGCUGCAGCCAGCUUUGCCCCAUGUGCCUAUUGUGUAGGCUGUGGGGCUGGCAACCAAAGAAGUGGGAAUGCUGAGUCUAAGCCAGAAAAAAUUCAGUUCAGUCCAAACUCUAAUUAUCUUGGAGGCAGCCUUUGUUCCAUUUGGUGGUUGAUUCAUUCCGAGCAUGGUUUCUGAAUUUUACUGGGGAGAGUGCACGCGUGUGUGUGUAUGUGUGUAUGUGUGUGCAUGCACACGCUUGUGUGUGAGGUGUGGAAAUAUUGGUUACCUCAACAGGCAGCUUUUGUUUUCUGAUAGCAGCUUGUGUAACCAGCUGUCAGGUAGAGGGGCCUCAUUAGCAGAGCAGAUUCCUGGGAAGGUCUUACAAGGAACAGACGCUGCCAGCACGUGGUUGGCCUGAAAAGGCACAGCUAGGUAGGUGCUCUGCUCCUCUUCCUUAUGAUCAAAGAGAGAAGAUGCUCCCCUGUGAACAGAGAAGUGGAGCAGGGACACUAUCUUCACUGUAUGACCUCUGGCUGUAUGUACAGAUAGAGCACUCCAUUCAUGACAUGGACGCUCAGUAAGUAAUUAUGGGCAUGUCAGUUUGAGCCAGCCAGUAACUGAUCUUAACAUCCUCUCCCUGCUGUGGCAAAAUCCUGACCAUGGCAAACCUAGCUCUUCGUCUCAUUUAUGAUGCUGGUAGGACUUGCUUGCUCAGAGCUGCUGCUCUCACUUUUUCUGGCACUGCCCACUCCUCCCAGCCUCCUCAGGUUUUCUGUCCAGUCUUGGAAACGUCAACCAGCCUUGCUGGGAUCAGCUUCUCAUGUUCCUGAGCAGUGUCCUUCAGCUGUUUAGCAAUGUCUUCAAGCCCCAAAUACAUACAUGCUCCUAAUUAUAGUCUGCAUGCCCCACUGGUUUCUGCUAAUCCCCCUACCCUCAACUCCCACUCCAGCUCGUCUCUACACCCAUCUGGACCCUGGCCUUGGGUUUCAAGCUGUUACUUGUGUCUGACCUCUCUGUUGGACCUCUCGCUUGUACUGCCUUUUUGGAGCCUGCCAAACAAAUUAAUGUAAAUUAUAUACACAAGGUAAAUUUUACUCAGCCAUAAAAGCCCAGUUUGAGAUGGGGAAGCAUCUUCUGAAAAGAGGAUAACUCUACAUGAGGAUGAUUCCAAGCUUGUGGCCCAGAUUCUGCUCUGUGUGCUUUGACCCUGGGGGUCGGCAUGAAGGGAUUGUAUUCUGGGAAAUUUGCCUCUUCUGUCAGUGAUUCUGGGACCAUUUCCUGCUUUGCUGGUCAUUGGCGUGCUUGAGUGUUCCAUUUUAAGCCCCCCGAGUAGAUACCCUCAUUGGGCUGGUACUUGAAGACAUCACUUUUCCAGUGUUCUUUUACCAUCUGUCCAGGUCAUUACAGUUCCCUAAAAUGAGGAAAGGUAGUGGGGUUAUAUUCCCUGAGGGAAGAGGAAUCUGCAGUUGCCUUGGGAAGGAGACAGGAAUGAGAGAGCUUGGGUGUUAAAUUGUUCAAAACAUGGUUGUUGAUAAAAUGCUACAACAUUUCAGCCCUGUGGCCAAACUGUAUGUGGGAUUCUGAGCUUCCGAGAGCUCACAGAACUGUGUGUCAGUGGUUCAGUGAUUCAACUUAGGCCUACCUAGGCAGAUGGGCCUAGAUGAAAAGAGCUCUGAUUUUGUGUUUAAUCUUUGCUCUCUCUUAGUUGUUGAAGGAGGAGAAAAUAAUUUCACCAAGAUGUGAGGUUAUGCAAUAAGAAAGAGUAAGAGAGUGAGGAAUUAAGAAUAUAAUGAUGAUUUUAUUUUUCUUUUUUCUUUUUUUUUUGCUUAUUGGAAGAGAAUGAAUACUUCUUGAGUCCCAGGCUCUUACUAAAAUGAGCUCUCUUAUACAUACACACACACACACACACACAUAUGUAUAUUGAGAAAUCUACAUAUCUGUAUAUACCUUUAAUUUUCACAAUUGCCUUAUAAUGUUGAUUUUAAUGUCCUUAUUGUAAAAAGGUAUAUUGAAAACUUCAGACAUUUUAUAAAUUUCCCCCCAAAUCAGGUUUUCAUCAAUUUUAGAUUGACCAGGGAUGGUUAUACACCUUCCUCCCUGUUUCCUCCCUUCUUUUCUUUGGACAGUGUUUAUUUUGGACCUUACUAUCACUCAGCUUUAUGUUAGAUAUUGUUCAACUCAGGAGAGAGAAACCUCAUGACACAUCCUGAUAUAAAUUGACUACAUAUAUUUUAAAGUUUUUAUUUUGAAAUAAUGAUAGAUGCAUAGAGGCUCACAAAGAAAUGUAUGGGGAAAUGCCAUGUAUUCACCUUCCAGCUCCCUCAGGGUUCACAUCUUACUUGAUUAUGGUACAAUCUCAAAACCAAGGAAUUAACAUUGAUAUUAUCCAUAGAGCUUUUUCAGAUUUCCCCAGUUGUGCACACAUCAUUUGCAUUUGUGACAAUUUUGUCACAUGUGUAGCCCUGUGUAAUUACCUCCACAAUCAACAGCCUCUCUACUGUGCCAUCAUGGUAACACUUCUAUUUUAUGGCCACACCCAUCCCCUCUCCUCCAUCCCUAAGCCUUGACAACUGUUACUCUGUUCUUUAUCUCUAUAAUUUUGUAAUUUCACAGAUGUUUUUUAAAUGGAAUCAUAUGGCAUGUAUUCUUUAAAGACUGGCUUUUUUUUUUCUCACGCAGCAUAAACUGUAGAUACCAGUAUUCUGAUCCUUUUUAAUGCUAAAUAGUCAUCCACGGUACGGAUGUGCCAAAAUUUUGUCUUACGAUUCAUGCCCUGAAGGAUGUUUGGGGAGUUUCCAAUUUGAGGCUGUUAAUAAGGCUGCUAUGAACAUUUGUGUACAAGUUCCUGUGUUAAAAAGAGAUUAAGUUCUCGUGAUGUAUGUCUUAAAAUUCAUUUGCGCUUAAGUAUGAAAAAAAGUCAUCAGAUUGUAGAGGGAGUUUGACAGCUAUAGAGAGAAAACCCAAUUAGAACUUAGUAACAGUGGCUAAGGUUGUUUUUCAGCAAGUAUGAUCUUUAACCAACAUCAUGGGUCAUAAGAGAUUUCAACCAUUGCAAGCUGUAUGUUAAAGCCUUCACUAAUCCCACUGGCUUUUAUACUGAUUUUGUUCUAUCCGUCUUAUUCUAGAGUUAACGUUUCUGCCAGGACCAGUUGUGUAGCAGUAUGUCCUAUUUCUUAGUUCUUUAAAGGCAAUAACUCAGCCAUAAAAGCCAGCAGGAGAGUACUUCACUGACAAAUUGGUUGGCCAGUCUUGUGUAUGUGCAUUAAAUCGUUGGGAGCAAAUAGGAAAGAGGAAGAGUGGGAGCAAAGCCUCUUCCGGUUUGCUUUUAAAUGUUAAAAAAAAAAAAAAGAAAUAGAAGGUAAAGAAAGCAAAAUUACACUGGAUGGAUUAUUGUGUUGGUAAUAGGAAAGUAACAAACUAUUUUAUAUUGAUUUCCCAUAUCCCUGGGAUUAAAAUAAAGUGACAUGCAAACACUGUGAAAUAAUUAAAAUUCUGUCGUUAAUUUUUUUUUUCAAGUAGAUCUAAUUUGAUGGCAGAAGGCUUUCCCAGGAGGUCCUUUUCAGAGAUAGAGGUGUAAUUUGCAAUAGGAAUAAUUAUAGAAACAACAUUCAUAUUCUGCUUUAUCUUUAAAGUUCCAGGCCUAAGUUAAUUUGUUUGUUUAUUCAUUUGUUUGUUCAUUUAUUCAUUCAUUCAAAUGAUAUUCUGAAUAAUUAUUAAUAUUUCUGCUUAUAAGCCUAGAUACUAAAGGGGCCCGAUACCACCUUCUGUGCUCCCCUUAAACCACUUCAUUCCCCAUCACCCCAUGAUUUUCCACAUUCAUGACUUCUCCUUGGGACACUUAUCCCCUCUGAUCACUUGUCUGAAAUCUACCUGUUCUUCAAAUCCCACCUCAAGUCUUACCUCCUCUGUUGACUUGCUUCUGAUUUCUCCUAGCUAGAAAUUUCAUACCUCUCUUCGGAUUUCCUCCAACAUUGUGUCUGUGGCCCUUUAAUACUUUCUACUUUAUAUUGUAGUUAUUUAUGUCCAUUUAACAUUCUUGCUACUCUGUUGUUAAUUUCCUUAGUAGUGGAUUCAUGUUUGAUUCCUUUUAGUGUUUAUUUGUUCUCUCCUUCCCUCCCUUCUUUUCUUUUUUCCUUCCUCUCACUUUCUUCCUUUCCUCCCUCUGUUCAUUUUUUUCUCUCAUUAAAUAUAUGCUGAACACCUACUAUAUACCAAACACUGUAAUAGGGGCUUUGAGUAGAAAGAAUUAAGAGCCAUUGUAGGUUCCUAAGGCAACCUAAUUAUGUACUUAAGUUAAACAUGAGGAAUUAAAAAAAAUUCCUGAUUGUUAGAUUGAGAUACUAAGAACAUCCUAAGACAGAAGGUAUUGGAUAUUCCUCUUUUAGAGGAAUUUUACAAAAAUUUUAGAGAAAUUUUAAGUGAAAGGCAACUAUUUUUUUUCUUGAGAGAGGAGCAUGUAAAUGUAGAGUUCCUAAAUGGCAAUAGGACUCACUUCAGUUUCAGAUCCAGGAUUCUGUGAACCUAAGGAAAAUUAUUGUGUUCCAAGGAAAAUUAUUGUCUACCUGUGGAUAGACAUCAACUAGAUGUCAGCUGAUGAUAUAAACUGAAAAUGCUAGAGGGAGAUGUGACUGGAAUUCAAAUAAUGUAUUGAAAUAAUUUUUAUUGGUACACAAAAUUCUUCAGCCAAGGAAUACAGCUCUGAAUUAUAAAAAAACUAUUUUAAAAGGCAAGUGGAACUACAGAAUAAGUAUUUCGUUUGUUUUUACUUCCUGUGUGGGUAUCUAAUUUUGUAAAUUGUUCUAUGACUGAGGAGUUUGAUAAAUGAUAAACAAGAAUGCCAUCCUCUAACUCUUCUCUACCUUUCUCUCUUCUCAGAAAGUUAUUGUGGAAAGAACAUACUCAAAGCUAGGAACAUCCACUAAGUGUAAUUUGUUUAGAGAGGGGUCAGUGAAGUGGGGUUUGUAGAUAAAAGUUUACAAAGCUGUCAGAAGUUCAAUGCCCUGGAUUUUAGGGAAUAAAUGUAGAGUCUGCAAGAGUUCAUUUCCACACAACAAAAUCUUUGGGAAACAUCAAGGCAUCUGCAACUAUGGAUGUGGGAAAAUCCAGGCAGAAAGGGCUCAGAGAUCACAGGAGCUCGGCAGUCUUUAGUGGCCAGCUUCACUGGGGAUAGAACCACUAUCAGGAGGGGCAAACCAGUUCUAUGGAUGGCCCCAGUACGGCUGGAUCACACUCAAAUUAGAAAGGAGACAGACGAGUGACCUGGGGAGCUCUUUCUAAAAGUCACUUAUGUAGCUACCUCAUAUGCUAGCACUGUGGCAUUUCUCUCCUGUGUCUUGUUUGUUUCUGUAGCAAAGCAUCUGGCAGCAGAGAAAUAUGGCUGCCCCAACUAUGUCACAGGUCAAAAGAGUGUUACCAGACUGAGGGUCUAGAAAUUUCUGCAAUGCAAAACAUGGCUUUGAAUUUCAUGUUCCUGGCAAUCACAAUGAAAACAAAUACUAUAUGAUCCUCAUGUUGUUGGGAAGAUUUUGAUUUGCUCCCCAGAGUAAAAUUUAGAUUUGUGUAAAAUUUUUUUGACACUGACUGAACUCUUUUGGGCCUUGUUUGAAUACAGUUUAUCUCAUUGUGCAACUUACCAGGAUUUGAGGCUCUAGUGUGCUUUUCAGAAAAAUGUAACUGCAAUUUUACACUAAAUGUUUUUACUCCCUAAAAAUAAGUAUCUGUGUUUUCUUUCUGUUUUGAUUGUCAAGUAGCUGUGUUUCUUAUGUAUGAAAUUUGGUUUAAGUGGCCAACUUUGAAAGAACAUUAUGAAACUUUGGUAUUUUUCAGGUCCUUGUGUCGCUUUGUGUGCUUAUUAUUUCAGAAAAAAAUAAAUUUAGAAUUUAUAAAAUUAAUUUCCCUUAAAAAAAUUUUUUUUUCUCACCAAAAAGGAGAAAAAAUAUGAAGAAUUUCUAUAUGUCUAUUUUUGGUCCCUUGACCAACCAGAGUUUUUUAGGGCAGGGGAUUUGUUGACUUCUUCAUAUCCCAGUGCCCAGGAAAGUCCUUGACAUAUAGCCUUUCCUCAAUAUUCUUGGAACAAAUGCUUAUUGAAGGUGCACAAAAGGGUUAGGAUGUCCUGAGGCCAAGAAUGAAAAACCACUUUCUUCAGUGUUUAUCCUGGGGCCCACCAAGCUGACCACUGAAGGUAGAAGAGAGACCACUUGAGAGCCUGAGGGAUCCCGGCAUGGGCUCUCCAUGGCCUGAGUUUCCCAUGUUCCAUAGGGUCUGCCCUGUUCCUCUUUAUUCCCUUCUCUGACACCUCAGCUACCCUCAGAGCUUCAUCUCAUCUCUGCAGACUCUUAAUUCUCAAAGCUACAUCCUCCAGCUUGCUCUUUUCCCUGAACUUCAGACCUAUAUAUCCACCCUUAGAAGUUUCAUAGACACUUCAAUUUAGUAAAUCCAAAUGGAAUGUAUUUAAAACUUUUUAUUCCAGGUUUGCUGCUCUUGUAUGUUCCCUACUUCAGUGAAGGGCACCAUCAUCCAGUUGCUAAUGCCACAAACCCGGGAGUCACCCUUCCCUCCCCUUGUUUCCCUAUCCUAUAUACAGUCAAUCACAAAGUUGUGUCCGUUCAACAUGUAAAAUAGUUCUUGAAUCUAGCUGCCUCCCUACACCCACACCAUUAAUAGCAUGGUUCAAACUAUCAUUUCUUUCCCAGUGGCCUCUUAAUUUAGGUAUUUGCUUCCAUUUGUAUUUCCUUCAAGUCAUAUGUAGCUGUACUGAAGCCAGAAUAAUCUUUCUAAAACAUGAAUGUUAUCAGGUAAUUUUUCAGUUUAAUGGUUCUGCAUUGUUUUCAAACUAAAGUCUGAGCUCGCUAGCAUGGUAUGCCUGGCCUUUAUAAGGAAACUCACUUGCCUUUCCUCACCACAGUGAACACUGUGUGCACCAACCAUAUUGUAUGUGUUUUAACUUCUCAAACAAUAUGUGCACCUCCAGUCCCUUGCACAUUCCUUCUGCCCAGAACACAAUUGAUUCCUUCUUUCAGCACAUUUUCUCACUAACUCUAAUCAUGUUUUAGUUCUUUACUUACACAUUGCUGCUUCCAGGAUGUUUCUCUUACCACGCAGCCUUGUGCUUCCAGGGACCUUGGACUUUGUCAUGUUUGCUUUUUUUUUUUUUUUUUUUUUAAAACAACAUAAUGUGUCUUGUGGUGCCCCUCUACUCAAGGAUAAACUUGACUAGGGUUUGAUUACCUUUGGGCCCCUUACCUAGCACUAUGCCUGGUUUAUCAUAGGUACUGAAUAAGGAGUUAAUGUAUCAGUCAGGGCAUGGGGUGGGGGUGUGAAUAUAGCAACAUGACUGUAUCCUCCAUGGUACAGUAGGAGAUCUUUUCAAGCUGUUGUUCUACUACCACUAUAAACUGCUGGCUCUUCAAAGGGCAUUCUUAGGAAAUAAAGCUCAGAGUUGUCAAGGGAUUAGAAAAACAUUUUUUAAGCAUCUUAAUGAGAUACAAUUCAAUACUAUAAAAGUCACCCAUUUAAAGCAUACAGUUCAGUGUUUCAUAUAUUCAGAAUUGUGCAACCAUUCUCAAAGUUUAAGUUUAAAAUAUUUUUAUCACUCAAAAGAGAAAUCCUGUACUUAUUAGUACUCAUUCCCUAUUUUCCCCUCCUACUCUCCCAUAACUCUACACAACCACUAAUCUACUGUCUGUCUGUGUAGAUUCACCUAUUCUGGACAUUUCAUAUAAAUGGGACAAUACAAUUUCUGAUCUUUUGCGUUUGGCUUCUUUCACUUAGAAAGAUUUCAAGAUUCAUCCAUGUUGUAGUACAUAUCAGUUCUUUACUCCUUUUUACCACCAAAUAAUAUUCCAUUCUGUGAGUUUGCCAGACUUUACCCAUUUAUCAAUUGAUGGACAUUGUGGUUGUUUCCAUAUUUUGGUUAUUAUGAAUAAUGUUGCUGUGAACAUUCUUAUGUAAGUUUUUGGGUAGACGUAUGUUUUUAGUUUUCAUUUCUCUUGAGUAUAUCCUUAAGUGUGAAAUUACUGGGUCAUGUGGUAACUCUGUUUAACAUUUUGAGGUGCUGCCAAGUCAUUUUUCAAAGCAGCUGCACCAUACAUAUUACAUUCCCAUCAAUAGUGUAUGAGGGUUCCAAUUUCUCAGCAUAAUCACCAACGCUUGUUAUUAUCUGUUUUUGGAUUAUUGCCAUCCUAGAUGAUGUGAAGUUGUAUCUCAUUGUGUUUUUCUUUUUUUUUUAGACAGGGUCUCACUUUGUCACCCAGGGUGGAAUCUGGAAUGCAGUGGUGGAAUCUUGGUUUACUGCAACCUCCACUUCCCGGGCUCAAGCAAUCCUCCUACCUCAGCCUCCCAAGUAGCAGGGACCACAGGCAUGCACCACCAUACCCAGCUAAUUUUUCUUAUUUUUUGUAGAGACAGGGUUUCACCAUGUUGCCCAGGCUGGUUUCAAACUCUUGGACUCAAGCAAUCCACCAUCCUCAGCCUCCCAAAGUGCUGGGAUUACAGGUGUGAGCUACCAUGCCUGGUCUCAUUGUGGUUUUGAUUUGUAUUUCCUUCAGGGGUAAUGAUGUUGAGCAUCUUUUCACAUGCUUAUUAACCAUUUGUGUAUUUUCCUUGAAGGAAUGUCUAUUCAGAUCCUUUAUUCAUUUUUUAUUUGGGUUGUUUGUCGUUUUAAUAAUUUUUAGGAGUUCUUUAUGUAUUCUAGAUACUAGUCCCUCAUUAAAUAUAGGGAUUGCAAAUGUUAUCUCCCAUUCUGUGUGCUUUUUCUUUUUACUUUCUUGAUGGUAUCAUUUAAAGCACAAAAUGUUUUAAUUUUGAUAUAGACCCGUUUAUCAAGUUUUUCUUUUGUGGCUUGUGCUUUUGGUGUCAUAUCUAAGAAACUAAUGCCUAAUCUAAGGUCAUGUAGAUUUAUUCUUAUGCUUUCUUCUAAGAGUUUUAUAGUUUUAACUCUUACAUUUAGAUCUAUGAUCCAUUUUGAGUUUAUUUUUGCAUAUGAUGUAAAGUUGUGAUCCAGCUUCAUUCUUUUGUGUACAGAUGUUCGCUUGUCCCAGCCAGUACCAUUUCUUGAAAAGACCAUUAUUUUCUCAUUGAAUUAUCUUGGCACUCUUGUCAAUGUCAAGGCAUUUUUGUCAUAAUUAUUCUCAUAAUUAUUGUUUGCCAUAUGAGUAACACAGGUUAACAAAUAAUGAUUAGCUUUAUUGAGUCUCAGUUAGGUGUUAGGCACCAUUCUAGAAGAUCUCCAUUUAGCAUUCCCAGUAACUAUGAAAUAAGUACUGCUAUUAUCCUCAUUUUUCUCUUAAGGAUGAAGAGGCAUGGAAAGAUUAACUUGGCAAAGGUCAUACAGGUAGUAAAUGUUGGACGCAGGCUUCGAACUCAGGCAACCUGACUAUAGAAUCUCUGUUUUUAGACAUCAUGCUGUGCCUGACUGUGUCUUGUUUAUAGGAGGAGGAAAAUUUUAAAACAGCCCAAAUUCUGUUAUCCAGAGAAGUAUUGUCAAAAUUUUCAUGUAUAGCUUUCCAAACUUUGUUCUGUACAAAAAAUGUUAUAAUAAUGGGAUUAGACUACAUAUACAUUCUUGAUUUUAUUCACUUUAUUGAUGUAUCAUUACUAACUUUCCUUCCUUCUAUAUCUAAAGCAUUAUUCUUAAUGGCUACAUAAUAUUCUACCUCAUGUCUGCACCAUUACUGAUUUAACCAUUCCACUGUUAUUGGGCAGUCAGGUUGCUUCUGAGUUUUUCAUUUAUAAACAAUGUUCUGAUGUAUGUAUCUUUGCACAUACUUCUAUUUAUAUUCUUUCCAUUGUUUUCUUUAAGAUAAGAAAAAAUUCCUCUAGAAGAAAUGUAAAGAGUAUGGAAAAACAUUUAAAGUUUUUAAUGCAUUUUGAAAAAUUGUUCUCUAGGAAGUUUCUACUUAUUUACAAUUAAUGUUUUAUAAUUGAUAGGUUACUCUGAUACUGAUUCAGGGUAGGCAAGCUCCCACUGGGGCUUAGCUGGGAAGGUUCUUGGCUUUGCCAAGGAAAAAAUUCAAGGGUGAGCCUUUGAAUUCUUUCCUUCUCUAAUAAAGAAAACAGCUUUAUUAAAGCGGCAGUGUUAUAGGUCUGGCAGUGUUAUAGGUCCAGCAGUGUUAUGGCUCCGUGACUUCUCCUGCAGAGCAGGGCUACCCCAUAGGGAGUAUGCUGAGAAGUAGCAGCUCAGGACAGUUCUGUAGUCAUAUUUAUUCCCACCUUUAACUAUAUACAAAUUAAGGAGCAGUCUGCAGAAAUUCCUAGAGAAAGGGUGGUAACUUCUGGGUGUUGCCAUAACAAUAGUAAACUGACAUGGCAUACUGAUGGGUGUCUUAUGGAAAGCCGUUUCCGCCUUGUCCCUAUUUUAGCUAGUCCUCAAUUUGGUCCAGUGUCUGAGCCCUGCCUCUGGAGUCUAGUCCUGCCUCUUAUCACUUUAGUGUGAAUCUCAUUGAUUCUCAGUGAGAUUGAACAUGUAUCAAUGAUUAUUAUAAUCUUUCUUGUGUGAAUUACCUAUUCAUAUUUUUACCCAUAUUUCCAUGAAAAAGCUCCUUGUAUACUAAAAUAUUAACCAUGUAUCUUUUUUUUGGUGUUUUCCUCUAGUUUGUCAUUUUUCUUUAAAAUUUUUGGGAAUUUUUUGAUGUAUAGAAGAUUUAAAUUUCCAAGUGGCAAAAUUUAUCAGCAAAAAAUAUACAUCUUUUUCUUUAUGGCAUCUUUGUGUUUGAAAAUCAAAGGUCAAAAAAUUGUUUCUAGCUCUUGUCUUCCAUGAGCUAGACGUUGGUGGUGGGUGGGGUGGGGGGCAGGCAGAAAUAUGAGGAAUCAUAUAAAUUGUCCUUUUUAUUUCCGCUGCAUGUUUUAUCUUAAACAUUGAUUACUUGUAGUCCCUUAACUGACAGGGAAAUAAAGCAUCAGCUUAACCAUUUGGCGUUAACAAUGUCAGUAGUGAGGCCACCUGGGGUGGAGAAUUAGUGUCUCCUCCCAGUUGUAUGGUUUUCAGCAAUAUUUUCCUCCCUGUGGUUUUUUUUUUUUAAACUCAUUUGAAUUUGCUCCUAGCAUGAAUACAUGAUAUAUUAGUCCAUUUUCAUACUGCUGUAAAGAACUUCCUGAGACUGGGUAAUUUAUAAAGGGAAGAGGUUUAAUUGACUGACAGUUCAGCAUGACUGGAGAGGCUUCAGGAAACUUACAAUCAUGGUGGAAGGUGACAGGGAAGUAAGGCAGGAAGGAGGGCAAGGCAGGAAGGCAGGGCAGCAGGAAGGAGAAGUGCCAAACAAAGUGGGAAGAGCCCUUUGUGAAACCAUCAGAUCUUGUGAGAACUGAGAACAUGAGAACAGCAUGGGGGAAACUGCCCCCAUGAUUCAAUUACCUCCACCUGGUCUCUCCCUUGACACGUGAAGAUUAUGGGGAUAAUGGGAUUAUAAAUCAAGAUGAGAUUUGGGUGGGGGCACAAAGCCUAACCAUAUCACAUACAAAUGACUUAAUGUGUAUGAGAUCAUAGGGACUUUUGUAGCACCAUUGGUUAGAAAAAUCACACAUUAUCCAAUUAGCGUUAAAAAGACAUGGAUGAAACUGGAAGCCAUCAUUCUCAGCCAACUGACACAGGAACAGAAAACCAAACACUGCAUGUUCUCACUCAUAAGUGGGAGUUGAACAAUGAGAACACAUGGACACAGGGAGGGGAACAACACAUACUGGGGCCUGUCGGAAGGUGGAGGGCAAGGGGAGGGAGAGCCCCUAAUGCAUGCGGGGCUGAAAACCUAGAUGACAGGUUGAUAGGUGCGGCAAACCACCAUGGCACAUGUAUACCUGUGUAACAAACCUGCAUGUUCUGCACAUGUAUCCCAGAACUUAAAAUAAAUAAAAAAAAAGACAUAUAUUUCUUCAAGACACAGUAAAUAAAAGUUCUUGAGAGUGUAUGCUUCUACACAAACUAGAUUUGUGGGCGUUAAAACAAUGUUACUUUUUCAGAAACUACUGCUGUGAUAGGGUGAUCUUUUGAAUCACAUUGUACCAGAAUUUUUUUUUUUGACGUUAUAGCUUUUAAAUGUUUUCAGACUAUCUUCUUACUGACUUGACAUUUAAUACCUUUGGCAUGUGAGUUUUCCUUAUUUCGUUUUCCAGAGUCUCAGGAAAAUACUUGUGUGUCUUGCCUGUUUACCAAUUAUUGCAGUGCAUUGCACUUUUUUCUGGGUCUGGUCUUUCAGCUACAUAUUGUGAAGGUGCUAUCCCGACCAGUCUCUUUGCAUAACCCCACAGGGCCACCCACGUGGUCUAUGGGACAGGGAUAACUCAUUAGGGCUUUCUUUGUCUUCUUUCUUGAGGGUCUAAGCUAAGCAGCACAUAUGUAAAAGAGCUUUAAGUUGAAAUUCUUUUGAGAGGUGUGUGUAUUUUUUAAAACUGGAAAUGCAGUUUUACCAACUGCAGUUGAGGAAGGCCCACAUGUAAAAAGUAAAGUAGAGGUUCCUCUUCAAAGAGACUUUCCUCCCAUCUAAUUAAGAAUAAAUAAUAACUUCUCUUAGAAGCAAAAUGUAUUCAAAGACCUGUGCUAACAUUCUUAGGUAUCUGCUAGCCACAAUAAAUAAAUCAAUGUACUUUGUGUCCUUAGCUCCCACAAUUUAGCCAAAAUAUUUGCCCUGGCGUGCUUAUACCAGUCCAAGCAAGCAUUAGGUCAUAGCCUGUUCCUUUCCUUAUUUGGAGAUGUUUUUACCUUUCUCAGCAUUCCACAAGUUACUUCGUCCUUCCUUUAUUCUCCUCUGCCUUUGCCUCUUUUAAAAAGUUCUAAGUUGCUAGCCAAUCAGGACAAAUACAGAAUGUGAGGUCCCAUUCCAGCCAAUGGAAACCAGACACAGCAGUAGGGUGGAUGUGUCAAGUUAUAAAUAACCCUGUCUCCUUUCUUCAGUGUAUUCUUGUGGCAAAACUGCUGGCAAGUGUACCUUUCUGCAGAAAGUAAAAAUGGCCUUGCUGAGAAAAUUUAUGUUCAAGUACUAUUUCUUUAUGGCACCAGGGAACAAGCAUUUCAAACACACGUGCAUAAGGAGUGUUAUUUUGCUGGUACUUCAUUAUUGUCUAAACUGUUUGUGUUUCUAGUAGGGGAGAUCAUGACUCAUAUUUGAAAAUUUGAUUUUAGAUAAUUAAAAAACUUACUUUUGAGUUUCUUCCAGUGCACUCUUUACCUUAUCAGAGCUCGUGUAUAUUAACACUAUCUGAAACACUGAAUGAGAAAGUGGGGAAGACUCAGCUUUUCAGGUUCUAAAAAUAUGAGUUGUACAUCUUGGCUUUCAAAUUUGCUUUUACAGGACAUUAGAAACUAAGAACAAGGGACUUUAUUGUUGUUAUGAUUAAUAGCUACAGUUGAUUAUCUUUUAUUUUCAGGGAUUGAAUUAGUUAUCAGUUGAUAUCCACAAUAAUCCUGUGAAAUGUAUGUUAUGAAUGAUCAUUUUACAGCUGGAAAAUGAGAGGCUCAAAGAUAACUUGCUUAAGAUAACAAAGUUAGAGGUAGAGCCAGGACUUGAAAUAGUAGGUCAUUUGACUGUGGAAUGCAUAUUUUAAAAUCAGCUUUAUUGAUUACAUAUACAAUAAAUAGCACAUAUUUAAAGUGUAUAAUAAGUUUUGACAUAUGCAUACACCAAAGCAAUCACUAUAUUCAGGAUAAAGAUCAUAUCCAUCACUUCCAAAAUUUUCCUCAUGACCCUUUUUAAUGCCUCCCUCUCCCCCAUAUGCCUAUCCCCAGGCAACGAAUUAUCUGCUUUCCAGCACUGUCAAUUAUUUUGCAUUUUCUAGAAUUUUACAUACACAGAUUCUGAUAUGGGUUUGGAUGUUUGUCCCUUCCAAAUCUCAUGUUGAAAUGUAAUCCCUAGUGUUGGAGGUGGGGCCUGGUGGGAGGUGGUUGGGUCAUGAGGGUGGAUCCCUCAUGAAUGGCCUAGUUCCUACAUCCACUUGGUGAUGAGUGAGUUCUCACUCAGUGAGUUCACAUAUGAUUGGGUUGUUUAAAACAGUCUGGUAUCUCCACCCCUGACUCUGGCUCCCACUCUUGCCACCACGUGAUACAAUGACUUCUUCCUUCACCUUCUGCCAUGAUUGUAAACUUCCUCACUAGAGGCCCUCACUAGAGGCCAAGCCAGUGUUGGUGUCAUGCUUCCUGUACAGCCUGCAGAACCAUGAGCCAGCUAAACCUCUUUUCUUUAGGAAUUACCUAGCCUCAGGUAUUUCUUUAUAGUUAUGUGAAAUUAACAUUCAUAUAGUGUGCUCUUUUGCAGCUUACUUCUUUCACUUAGUUUGACUACUUUGACAGUCAUCCAUGUUGUUGCAUAUAUCAAUGGUUCAUUCCUUAUAUUGUGGAAUACUAGUUCAUUAUAUGGCUUAUAUAUCACAAUAUUCUAAUUUAUUCACUGUUGGCUGGCAUUUGGGUUGUUUUCAGUUUGGGGCUGUUAUGAAUAUAGUUGCUAAGAACAUUCAUAUGCAAGAUUUUGUAUGGAUAUAGGCUUUCUCUUCUCUAGAAGAGAUACCUAAAAGUGGAAUGGCUACAUCAUAUAGUAGCUGCAUGUUUAAUGGUUUAAGAAACUGUCAAACUUUUUUCCAAAGUUGUACCAUUUUACAUUCCCAUCAGCAGGAUAUGAGAGUUCUAGUCGCUCCAUAUCCUUGUCAACACUUGGCACAAUCAGCCUUUUUAAUUUUAGCCAUUCUAAUAGAGAAAAGUUUCUCAUUGUGACUUAAUAAUUGUAUUUCUGCAACAUCUAAUGAUGUUGAGGGUAUUUCCAUGUGCUUACUUAUUACCUUUUUAUCUUCUUUGGUCAAAUAUCUGUUUAAAUCCUUUGCUCAUUUAAAAUUUGUUAAUUUGGCUGGGUGUGGUGGCUCAUGCCUGUAAUCCCAGCACUUUGGGAGGCUGAGGUGGGUGGAUCACGAGGUCAGGAGAUCGAGACCAUCCUGGCUAACACGGCAAAACCCUGUCUCUACUAAAAAUACAAAAAAUUAGCCAGGCAUAGUGGUGGGCACCUGUAGUCCCAGCUACUUGGGAGGCUGAGGCAGGAGAAUGGCGUGAACCCGGGAGGUGGAACUUGCAGUGAACUGAGAUUGCACCACUGCACUCCAGCCUGGGCAACAGAGCGAGACUUCUUCUCAAAAAAAAAAAAAAUUGUUAAUUUAUUUAAAACUGAAUUUUAAGUCUUUGUAUAUUUCAGAUACAAGUCCUUUAUCAGAUUUGUGAUUUGAAAAUAUUUUCUUGUGGUCUGUGGCUUGUUUCUUAUUUUCUUAACCCUGUCUUUUGAAGAGUAUAACAUUCUUAAUUUUAAUAAAGUCCAGCUUAUUAGUUUCUUUUUUUGUAUGGAUUGUGCUUUUGAUGUCUGUUAUGGGUUAAUUGUGUCCACCUAAAAAAGAUGUUGGCAUCCUAACCCCUUGUUCUGCAGAAUGUAACCUUAUUUGAAGAUGGAGUCUUUACAGAGGUAACCAAAUUAAAAUGAAGUCAUUAUGAUGGGCUCUAAUCCAAUAUGACUGGUGUCCUUAUAAAAAGGAGGAAUUUAGACACAAGUGCAGAGGGAAGACUGAUGUGAAGACCCAGGGAAAAGAGAGCCAUCUCCAAGCCAAGGAGAGAGGCCUGGAACACGUCCUUCCUUCACUGCCCUCAGAAGGAACUAACCUUGCUGACACCUUGAUUUUGGACUUCUAGCCUCCAUAAUUGUAAGACAAUAAAUUUCUGAUUUUAUAGUGACCUGGUUUGUGAUACUUUUCUAUGGCAGACAUUGCACACUAAUGUAGUGUCACAGAGAUUUUCUCCUACAUUUUCUUUUGGAACUUUUAUAGUUUUAGGAUUUCCAUUUAGGUCUAUGAUUCAUUUUGAGUUGAUUUUUUUAUGUGGUGGCAAGUAUGGUUUGAAACUCAAUAUGGAAAUUUACACAUGGAAAUCCGGUAGUUUCAGCCUCAUUUGUUGAAAAGAUUAUCUUUCUCCAUUGAAUUGCUAUUUUACCUCUGUUAAAAAUUAGUUUUCUAUUCAUGUGUGUAUGUUUCAAGACCCUCUAUUCUGCUCCAUUGACCUAUUUGUCUAUCUUGAUGCUAAUACCAAUCUGCCUUCUUUACUUUAGCUUUAUAAUAAGACUUCAUAUCAGAUUGUUUUAGUUCCCCUUUGUUCUUUUUAAAAAUUGAUUUGGCUAUUUUAGGCCUUUGGCAUUUCCAUAUGAAUUUUAGAAUCAGUUUGUCAGUUGUUAUAGCUGGAUUGUACUGAAUCAUAGAUAGAUUUGAGGAGAUAAUAUCUUAACAAUAUCACGUCUUCUGACCUAUAAACAUAGGUGUAUCUCAACAUUAUUUUAGAUGUUGUUUAGUUUCAGCGAUGUUUUGUAGUUUUCAUUAUACAGGUCUUGACAAUCUCUUGUUAGAUUUAUUAGCAUUUCAGAUUUUUUAUAUGACUAUAGAUGGUAUUUUUAAAUUUCAACUUCUGAUUGUUCAUUUAUAGUAUCCAGAAAUAUAGUUGAGUUUUAUAUAAUGAUCUCAUAUCCUAAAGGCUUAUUAAACUGAUUGAUCAGUUCUAAUAGCUUUUUGGCAGAUUCCAUGAGGUUUUCUACAUAAAAUGUCAUGUUGUUUGUAAAUAAAGACAGUUUUACUUCUUCUUUUCCAGUCUGCAUACGUUUUCUUUCUUUUCAUUGCCUUAAUGCACUGGAUGCAACCUUCAUAAUAAUGUUGAAUAUUAGCAGUAAGAGGAGACAUCCUUGUCUCAUUGCUGAUCUUAUAAGGAAAGCAUUCAGUCUUUUACCUUUAAGUAUGAUGUUGAUCAGGUUGGCACCUUUUCUCUGAAAAGUACAAGGUAGUAAAUUUUUGGCUUGAGGACCACAGGGUCUCCAUUAUAACUACUCACUCAGAUGUUGUAGUACAAAAGCAGCCAUGUCUUUCUCAUAUGCAUGCGUUCAUCCUUACUUAGCUGGAUACUCAAGUGGGAUUCUUUGCAGAUCUCUCUAUUUAGCUCUCUUUAUGUAGCUCUUUUUUUCUCUGGUAUGCUGUCCUGUGAAUUCUAACUUCCUUGGUCUUCCUGGAACCCCAACUCCAUCUCCUGACUCAGAGAGUUCACUGGGCUCCACCUGGGUUACUUGUGUUGGACUGAGCCCUGGAAACCUUCCCAAGGCAGUAAGCUAUGGCAACCACAGGGCUCCCUGUCUUUGUUUCGCAUAUCUCCAAUGCAAACCUUCAUUGCCUGUUCCUUGUGGCCUGAUGUCCAGUGUUUUGAAAGCCAUUGUUUUAUGUAUUUGUAUGUUUUUAGAUUGUUUCUUAUGGGAGGAUAAAUCUAGUCACUGAUUCUUCAUUUUGGGCAGAAUCUGCCAUAUUUUCCCCCAUAAUCUUGCAUUAUUCUGUAUCUUGGUUAAGAGUCUAGUCAUCAUUAUCUAACUUGGAGGAAUCUAUAGCCUUUUUUUUGUCUUAUGAUAUCAAAAUAUUUUUGAACCCUUCAUUUGGACCUUUAAUAUCUAUUGAUUUACACGUAAGGUAAACAAACUUUUGUAACUUAAUCAAUACAUUUCAAUAUGCUUGUAUUUGAUAAAACAUGGUAGCAUCUAUUUGAUGCUGAAACAUGGCAAAGCAUAUGUUGUUAUAUAGUCAUGUCUUUUUUUUUCAGUUCACUAACAGUGCAGAUGUGCGUAUGAAUUCACAAACUCCUUUGCAAUAAUCGCUGAGGUUCCCCAGAUGUUCUUGCAGCCCAGGCUGGAAAUCACUAGCCUAUAGGAUUUUUAUGUGUGACAUAUUGACUGGAGGUGUCCUUCAGUUCAUGGUUAAUUUGAACCAGAUUUUCAUGUGUCUUCAAGUUGGUGACCUAUGAAAUAGUGUUGUGGUUUAAAUCCCUGAACCCAGUAGUAGGGACCAAGGUGGACCUGGCAGGUGCACUUGUACUCGAGUGUAGUUCAUCAGAGACUGGACCUCGAGUUCCUUUGUCUACCCAAGGAAGACAUGUGUGGAAAGGAUCCUUAAUGGAACGUGCCUAACCUAGAAACCUUGAUGAACAGUGAAGGUCAAGCCUAGAAGUAGCAUCAAGUCAACAAAUUCAGAGGAUGCAAGCUGUGAUGAAAAUGGGAGGCAGUCAAGAGGCAGAAACUAGGUGGACAUGGAAUAAAAUACCAGUGGUUUGGAAGCUAAGCCAGUGAGGUAGUGGCAUGGGGCUUGAUGCAAAUGCCACUAGAUCAUCCAUAGCUGCUUUUAUAUCUGGCAUGUAGCUCAUGGGUAGAUUGGGUCUGAAUAGCCACAGGGUUAUAGAAGACAGCUGUAUAGGAGUUUUUGCUGUAAGUAUUCAUUGAAGGAAUGGUGGAAAACAAUACCAAAAACCAUGCUUGAAUUGAUAUCUGGAUAUUUUGUUUGUAGAUAAACAUUUUUACCACUUAUCUUAAAAGUUCUCUGAAAUGCUUUGUUCUAAAAUUCCUAUUAUAUUAGCUUCUACUCCCCAUGAUAGUCUUUCUAGAGAGAAUGUCUCAAAAAAUAAUAGAUCUGACCAUUCAGUCAACAAACACUUUUUGAAUCCCUGCCCUGUGCCACGUACUGUUUUAGGUAUUGAGGGUGCACAAAUGAAAAAUAAACAAAUCAAUGAUUUAUUUGAGUUUCCAUGCUGGUAGAAUGAGGCAUAAGAUAAAGAAAAUAAAAAGGUAAAAUACGUGGAAUGACUAGUUGUGCUCAAUGCUAUGGAGAACAAUAAGGCUAAUUGGGACUAGUGACAGUGGUAGUGGCAUUGGUGGUAUUUGUGUGCAAAUAAAUAUAGUGUGGACAGAAAAGGCAAAGACCUGAAGUGGCUGAACAUUAUAUCUAUUGUCAGCUAUCUUGAUGAUUUGUCUCAUAAUAAGCCUCCAUGAUAUUUUAAAAAAUAAUAAUUCAAGCCACCUUUUACACAUGUGAUUCCUUCUCGUGGCCUCCUUUGCUCAUAUUCCUGAUCCCAGCCACAAGAGCAGGAUUGUAAAACUGAUCUGAUUUACAAUAUCUUAAAAGUCAGUGGGCUGAAGCUUUGCUAGAAAAAAAGUAGAGCUAGGAGGCCAGUGUGGUAGACGUGCUGAGGUGGCUCUUUGGGGGAAAAGAGUUAGUGCGACAUUUUUGAGGGUCCAGCUUAUUUUUUAGGACACAUGGCCUAUGUACAGACAGUGGUACUGAACAGAAAAUGGCAAGCAAUGGACUCUGACACAGCCAGAUAAAUUUGUCUUUAAGAUCUAUUUGGGUCCUAAUAGAGUUAGUUAAACUAAUUUGAUAAAAAAUAGGUUGCUGAUGGAAUUCCAAAUUUCAUACUCACUUAUUUAGUCAUGGUGCAUGUACUUAAAUGUCAUAAAAAUUAAGAUAAAUCUUGGAAGACAUAGGACUAUGAUUACACCAAAGAGCAUCACAGAAAGUGAAUGUAACGGGGGAGGUAGGGAGUCCUCUACCACUGAAGUAUUGAUAUGCCAGAUGCUGGGCUUUUGGUACUUUUGUCUUGCUUAAGAGCACUGUAGCUGGAGGGUGGCAGAGCCAAGAUUUAGACCUGCCUUGGGUGACUCCAUAGAUGGAGCACUUUGCAUCAUGGCACUCUUCUUUUUUACUGUCUUUGGUGGCUUCAUGGGCCACAAUUUCUCUCUGUUUUUCACCUUUGUUGGCCAUAAGUGCAGCUCUUUGCCAGCAUCAACCACGUUUCUUCCAUACCCAGCUUGCCUGUUUAUGGAAUUUCAUCACGGUUUUGUUUCCUGCUGUGCCUAUGAGUAGAAGAAAAACAUUCCAACAUUGAGCUCUUAUCCUUCUAAGGGAAAUGGCAUCACUGCAUCUUGUACUGCUAGUACCAGCUGUAAGUGAUGGGCCUGGCAAUGGAGCCCUCCUUGGACACAGGGCCUCUGACCCAGUUCUACUGGUGGUGUCUGAAGGAUCUGACACCCAAACCAUGGCUUAUUUCCCCUGUGAACAUUCACCACUGUAGAAACAUUUCGUUCCUGUAAAAAGACAUCUUAUAUCCUCUACCCCUGUAUUGUAUAGUGUGGGGGAGGAUUUUCUAUUUUAAGAUAAAUAAGACAAUUUUUUUUCAAAUUGAUCAGCCAAUGCCAGAGAACAUUAAUUCUUUUGGAGAGCAUUGUUCCUAUAAAGUGAAACUACUCCACCAAAUUAACAUGCCAAAAAAACAAGAGGAGAGCUGUUUCAGGCAAAGAAGUAGAAAUCAAUUACCUGAAAAAAUUUCAACGGUAUUUAUUUUAGGUGAUUUUAUUUCCAGAUUAAACAAAUAAAACUCCUGUGUCUUUUCUUACCUGUUUGACUUUUCAGUCAGAACUAAUGGAACCAAGAAAGGAACAAUAGACUUAUUAUUGAUCUGCAAAAAGAAAAGGCCCCUAAAGAAAGGCAAUAAUGACAUUUUAAAGAAGUGACUCUUGAAAAAAAUAUUUUUCAUGAAUACUUUAAGAUAUCUUUUAUAGUACUGGAAAAAUUUGAUUUAAGUCUGGCUUGAACAUGUAAGUGUGUCUGUAAGUAACAGUACGUGCAGAAAAAAAAGGUAGCAAAUGCAGAUUCUGAAUCUGUACAAAACCUGUUUAAAAUGCGCACAUCCAAAAAUGCCAAAUUAGCAGUAGACCAGAAACAACCCCCAGGACUGUGGAUGUAUGCUUAGUGUUGAAGUGUCUAUUCUAGUUCUACUCUUCAAACACACCAGCCAUUUGGGUGUGGUUCCUUCUAGUGUGAUUGGAGGAACCCCUUCUUUUAUACUAAUAUACACUCAUACACCCCUUCUUUUACACAGUUAAAAUUCUGGAUCUGGUGAGGUUUGUGUGAUUUCUCAGAUCACAAUUCUUUUUUUUUUUUUUUUUUUUUUUUUUGAAAUGGAGUCUCGCUCUGUCGCCCAGGCUGGAGUGCAGUGGUGCGAUCUCGGCUCACUGCAAGCUCCGCCUCCUGGGUUCACACCAUUCUCCUGCCUCAGCCUCCUGAGUAGCUGGGACUACAGGCACCCACCACAACACCCAGCUAAUUUUUUGUAUUUUUAGUAGAGACAGGAUUUCACCGUGUUAGCCAGGAUGGUCUCGAUCUCCUGACAUCAUGAUCUGCCUGCCUCGGCCUCCCAAAAUGCUGGGAUUACUGGCAUGAACCACCGCACCCGGCCAGAAUCUCAAUAUUUUUAUCCAGUUGUGAAUGUGAAAUGAGAUGAUGUGAGUGGGCACUUGAUAAAAAGGGGCCAUUCAUGGAGUAAUGAUGAGAGUUCAUGGCCAGGGGUUUUGAUCAAUUCAGUCUAAUUCUACGGACCUGAAGUUCAAUGUUUUAAAGGUGCUCUAUAACCAAUAAAGUGCUAUGGAUCAGUAAAACAUUGGUGACGGUGCUAGGUUGUAGGAUAUGCACUUUGAGUCCAAGGAGGCAAUGUUUUAUCCAUUUCAUCCUCCAUAGGAGCUAGCACCAAUAUGAACACAUAAUAUGUAUCAAAUAAAUUACCUCAUGGAAAUCAGAAGAGACCUCAGUUUUCUCUAACAAUCUAGAUUUCUUCACAAGUGGCUCUUCAAAUAUGUUAAAAAGUGUAUUCUGUUCUCAAUAAUUUAGUAUUAAGGAAAAUGUACCUAAUAUGUGUACUUGAACUAUUUCUGUGGUAUGUGAUAGAAAAUCCAUCUUAAAUUAUUAUAAGAAAUAAAAGCACAAUUUAUUAACAAAGGAAUUGGAGAAUCUGAGAGCAUAUUGGAUUUAGGUUUGGGUUGAUCUGGGAGCUCAGAUGAAGGCAUAGAGACCAGGUGUCUUACUCCAUCUUCCUACAUCCCUGCUCUAAAGAGGCUCUGCUCUCUGCCAGGCUUAUCUGUUGCAGCUAGGCCUCACAAGACCCCAGGUUCAAAUCCAGCAGGAAAAAAAGUCUCUAGUAACUCUUGCACAACCCCCAGGACUCACUUGGACUAGCGGAGCUUGGGACAGAUGCUUAUCCCUUAACAGUUCCUGAAGAGUAUUCUACUGCCAGAGGAAAGGAGGAGUGGACGCCAGGUGGCCUGUAUGCAGUAAGAGUCCACUCCAUCUAUGGACCCCUUGGUUACCUUUUCCAGGCCUUUGUAGCUCACUCCUCCUCAGGUAAAAUUUAGAGAAGUGAUAUUAUUUUUAAUAAGAUCACGAGAGGUCCAAAUAGUCUAAUUUGUUAUAUUGGUUUUUUUUUCAGGUUUUUUGGGGGCCAUUUUGUGUUCAUAGGCAGUAAAACAACAGAGGUUUUCCCCAGGUAUCUAAACUGCACCCAAAAGUCUGACAAGAUCUUUCUAGUGAUCUUGGGAUGCAGGGAUUUGGGUGCCAGGAACUGAGUUCGAGUCCUCAUUACCUGUCUUGGCUGUGGCUUUGUGGCAAACUGAUCAAUAUGGCUUCCACAGAGCUCCACAUGAACACGUACAGAGCAGCCACGUUACAUUCCAUACAGUGGGAAGUCUUCACAGAUGCCCCUUUCUCAUCAUUCACAUUUCACCUUGUUAGAAAGGUCUUCCUCACUCUUCUUAAUAAAACAUUGUUAUCUGAAAUUAGUUGUUUAUUUGUUUUUUGUCUACUCUCACUAACUCCAUAUGAGUAUUAAACCCCAUAAGAGUAAAAAUGUUUUUCUAUCUUCUUUCCUUCAGUAGCCACAGCAUCUGAAACAGUGUGUGACAUAUGGUAGGCACUCAUUACACAGUUCCUAGAACAUGAAUGAAUGGCUUCUAAAACCAUUUUUCUACAGUCUCUGUAGAGGCAGUAGGUACAAACUGUGUUUUGUAAAUGAGGUUGGAUUGAAUGACUACCAUAGCUGAAUCCAGUCAUAGCUAUGUUGUUAUAAUGGAUGGGCCAUGCAAUGUAAUGAAGUAAUUAACUCCCUAAGUUUGUACUUUAUCCAAAAGACAUAUUACUGGCUUUAGGUGAGGAAUGAGUCUGGCUUCCAUGAUGGAUGGAACUUAUAUUUAAAGACAAUAAGCAUUGUACUAUACAGUGUUUUAUCUUGAACCACACAGUUGCAUCUGAGGACAAAUGUGAUUGCACUAUACAGAAACAGAAUAAGGUUUGUGAUUAAUGCACUCUUGGAGCUCACAAUCUCACCAUCUAUUCGCAGAGAUAUUGAAGUAGUAGUUACUUCACUCACAGAAUUCUAUCAUAGUUCCUGGAAAUGAGCUAGAGUUUCCCUUGUCAAUUCCUUUAUGGGUGCUCCAUUGCCCUAAUCUGUGAGAAAAAGAACUGAUUCCAGCAAGUGAACUCAUUAAAGGGAGUCUACAUUUCCUUAUUCCAGAGAGAAGCUGUUGAUUGGAUCUCUGAGUAGCUCUGUCGUAGGCUGGGCUCCUUGAUGAAUUGAAUUCAUUUACUCAAAUGUGCAGGCUUAAACUUUGCAGAAAUGAAAUUGAAUGACCAUCAAGAGAAGCUAUAGUGCUGAUGGUUUAGUAUAUUAGUAGACCUCAGAGCAUAAGUUAGCUUUAUUUAUAGAUACUACUUUUGUGGUGAACUAUCUAAAAGGAUAUCAAGAAAAAGAAACUGAAUUUCAAUUUUCAGAAUAUUGCUUGUAGUUAUCACUCUGUUAGUCCAAAUGAUUUAAACUUUUUCAUUCCAUGUUGACAUUUUAAACAAACACAUAUGAGCACUUUCCAGGUACUAAGAACCUGUUUUGGUUUCAGGAAAUACCCAGUUCAAAGGAAGAGGGACAGAUCUGUACACCAGUGAUUUUAAUAUAUAUUAUAAAUAGUAUGAUAGAAAUCUGUGCAAAAUUUCAUAAGAGGUGGCACAUAAUUCUUAUUGGGAUGGGGGUGGUGUGUGUGUGUUGUGUUUAUUCUCUGGCUAUGGUUUUUGUUUAAUAAUACUGGAAACAAAAACCACACAACUAACAUUUGUUAAGUGCUUUUUAUGUCAGGCGCUGUUCUAAUUACUUUUUCACCUAUACUCUCAUUUAAUCCCCGAAGUGGACUCUGUGGAUCACAGGUACCUGGAUCACCCCAUUUUCACAGAUGAGGAAACUGAGGCUCAAAGAGGAUCAAUAACUUGCCCAAGGUCAUGUGGAGGAGACUACCUUCAACUAGGUGAUAUCUUGUCAGCCAUCAGCCCGCCAGCUCCAUGGUGCCUCCUGCUUUGGCUGGGUAGCAGGACUCUCCUGCGUGUGCUCCCUGUAGAUAUUUAUGAAUGUGUUUCUUUUUUUUACUCGCUUCAUGUUUGUAAUCCAUGAACAUGUGUGUGUGCCUCUAGGGUGACUUCAUUAGUGUCAGGGGAGAAACUUACAUACAUAUGUGUACAAUGAAAUAGUGUUGUUGACCUGUUUUAGAAAGCUCACAUCUUAGUAGUUCCCACUGCAGUUUUUACUGGGGUCUCUCUUAGUCUUCAGCACUAAGUCAGAUCUAUUGCGGUUUUUUGUUGUUUUGAGACAGAGUCUUGCUCUGUCACCCAGGCUGGAGUGUAGUGGCACGAUCUCAGCUCACUGCAACCUCCACCUCCUGGGUUCAAGUGAUUCUCCUGCCUCAGCUUCCUGAGUAGCUGGGAUUACAGGAACCUGCCACAACGCUCAGCUAAUUUUUGUAUUUUAGUAGAGGUGGGGUUUUGCUGUGUUGGCCAGACUGGUCUCAAACUCCUGACCUCAAGCAAUCCACCUGCCUUGGCCUCCCAAAGUGCUGGGAUUACAGGUGUGCCCAGCCAGACCUAUUGUGUUUUAAUGCUUGCUGAUGGGAAGUUCUGCCUUGGAGCCUUGGGAUUUUGAUUUUGAUUGAGCUCCUCCCCUAAUUUUUUUUUUACUUUUUUACAUGACACCUUUUUCGUCAUCUGCAAAAUGGAGAUAAGGAUGCAUUUACUCCCUCAAUGAUGGGGUCGCUGGUCAGGUCAUUCAUUCCUGUGGGUGUUGGUUUAGUAAGUCUGCAGUGAUGAACUCCUUUAUGGGAGCUGGUGUGUACGCUGUUACUCCAGGGCCAGCCCUGAUGGGAGUUGUGCUCAUGGAGCUCACAGCCUCACAGGGAAGAUCUCAUGCACAUAAAUAACCGUAAUACAUGAUAAUAAUACAAAUAAUAACAGGAGCCAUAGGCAGCUGCCACUUAUCAGUAGCUUGCUAUGUAUCAGAAAUACGUACUUUUAUUUAGGCAUCAGAAUCAACUCCUGAUAUGGGAUCUUUUGUUUAUUUUUAAAACUCACUUAAAAAACAGCUUUUAAAAUAGUAUACAUGCAUAGUAAAAACUUAAGGCAUACAAAAGUGCAGUAAGUGAAAAGUUGGUAUUUUUUCCACUGUAGAUUUCUCAGUCCUAUUCUCCAAAGAAAAAUCACCAUAAACAUUUUCUUCUGUAUUCUUUAAGAAUGCUUAUUCACAUGCUGGCAUAUAUGCCUAUCCAUUCUUUUACAGAGUGUGAUUGUAUUAUGUACAAUUCUAUGCCUUGUUUUUUCACUUGGUGUUUUUGCUGUCUCCACCCUCCCCAUACAUACACACACACACACACACACACACGUAUACACACACAGGCACAUGUAUACAAACGUGGAGAGAUCAAUCUCGACCUUUUUAUUUUUGAUAGCAAAUAGUAGUCCUUUUCAGGGAUGAGUUUAAAAAAUUAUGUCCUGUGAAAAUAUUCUGUAAAAGCAAAAAUAUAUUCAAAAAAGUAAAUAUAUUCCAUAUGAAAUGGUGUGGGGGCUGUAUUGGAGCUUGAACUAAAUGGCAUCAGAAAAGGGCUCUGGUUCCAGGGUACCAGACAUCCCCGGCAGAGAAUGGAGGCUGGAGGUGGUAAUGGGCAAGGCUGGGGAUAUGAAGAGUCCCAUGGGACAUGAGCGUGUCCAGGGCUCAUCUUGGGCACCUGCCCCAUGAUGAAAGCUCCGAUUUCCACUCCUCUGGCUGUGUUUGAGCUGGUGAGAGGGUUCUGCGAUGUUUGUGAGUAGCUCAGGAACUGAGUGAAGCAGAAACAGAUAAUGAGGGGUGUGGCUGCCAUCAUGGGCUCAGGUCUCCCAUACCACUCUCCUGCCUCUUCUGUGAUUUCUCCCUUUGCUCCACGCCUAUGCCUUCUACCCCACCAGCCUUUCCUGGUGAAAUCCUGUUCUUCUUUCCAAACCUUCCCCCAACCAUCUUGUUUCCCUCUUAUAGCAUCAGGAAUAUAGCAGUGAUAGGAGCCUACUUGUCUUGAGUUCUCACUAUGCGCCAGAUGCCACCAACCAUUCUGAGCUCGUUGCAUGAAUUUACUCAUUUAAUCCUUACCCCACCUUUUAAGAGACUGUUAUCACCAUUUUACAGAUGAGGAAAUCUGAGGCACAGAAAGGCUCCCCCCUUUCCUGAGCGGUGAAGCCCAGUUUACAUUAGUACAGUCUAGUUAUACUGCCGGACGUCACCAUAACUGCUGUCAUUUAAUCCUCACAGUGACCGUGAGGUAGGUGUGGGUAUCUCCCUUUUCACAGAUGAGAACAUGGGAGCUCAGAGGGGCUGAGCAGCUUGCCAAAUUUGUGCCAUAGGUAGUGGCAGAACUGUUUUUGUAAUCUGAUUCUCUCAACUCUCCCCCUAACUCCCUGCCUCUGCAUGGAAAUCUGUAUUAGGAGCACUUGUGCCUGUUCUUCCCACCACUCCUGGGGUCUCCUUUUCUCCCCCAGCAACAGCCAUGCUCAGCUGUUGAACUCAGUAAAUAAUUGCUGAAUGAUUAAUCUCUCUCAUGACUGCUCUGUGUGUGAGGGUUCCUUAAUUACCAAAACUUUAAGGCAUGUCUCAUUGUAAAUGUUUUGAAAUUGUAUAUGGUAAAGUGUAAAAACAUGUGGUGUGUUAAUGUUGAUAUCUCACCUUGAGUUCAUCUGUCUCUUGCCUAAAGGUGUUUUUAUAUCCAUGUAGAGUGCCUUUUACUCUAUGGCUCCUGAUCUGCCAUGCAAUCAACAGAUUUAAUAAUUUAUCAAUGUCAUAUGAGGCUUAUCUUGAAGCUGAGUGUGAAGUGGCUUCAGGGUCAGAGAGCUGGGUCUUGCAGAUUCCUGGUGCUUUUUCCAGGCUCUGUUGGGCUCUACUGAGCAUGGUUUUGCACAGUUCCCCUGCCCUUACCCUGGCUGUGGGACCCUGGGAUAGGUGUUUGAACGGAGUUGUAAUAGUGUGUGUCAGUUAUGUUGGAUCAUUUUCCCAAGUGUAAUUUGAGCGUGUGCAACCUGUGAUAUGUUCUUAUGAAAAGCACAUUUGCAUAUUAAUGUAUCUGCAUUUUGAUUCUAAGCCCUUUACUUCCAUAGGACUGUGCCCUGAAUUUAUGCUUAGGUCUGAGAAUGUCUGUGAGUUCUAGAGGGGCUGUGCCUGUGUCUGAUAUGACUCUGCCCCCAACUGUCCCCUCCCCACAUGCCUAGCACAGUGCCCGGUACACAGUGAGCAAGCCAGAAGUACUGAAUGAAUGAGUGGUUGUGUCUUCAGGAAGAUGAGUAAGGGUCGGCAUAGGAAAGAGUUUCUGAAAAUGUUCCAAGUAUAUCAGUUCUUCUGUUACUGAGCCCCAAAUUUCCUUCAUGUUUCAGUACUUGCAAAUGAUCUGAGGUUUUUCUGGCAGCCCAGUCUUUAGGAGGUGACACAGCAACCUCAGCUGUGACCUGCUUGGUUGCAGUGGAUUUUGCAUAGAGAGUAGCUGUAAUUAAACUGUUGAUUUGGCUUAAUGCUGUUGAUUUGCUUUCAUCAUUUGAGAAAAUGUGCAGAUAUUAUAAAACUUGCCAGGGGCUGGGAUUUGGCUGUGGAAAUAAAUUUUGGUUAAUUAUUUAGCUAAAGAACUUUUAGUAUUAGAAUUUUUGUGUUAAUGAAAUUGUUAGUUAUGUUCAAAUCAUGAUGUAUAUGAUGACUAAAUUACCAUAAUUUUUCUUCUAAUGGUCAUUUUCUGCUUCUGUCCCUUUAACUGUGUUAUAGACCAUAUACCUGAUUAUGAAGGAUUAUUUAGUUUAACAGUUCUUUUAUGGAUCACUAAUAUAAACUUAUAGUUGUACCUAGAUGUGUACAAGUAUAGUUGACAAUGAUCAUUCGGUAUAUUACCUUUGGUUUCCUUUGCAGGAAUUAAUUGACAUAAUAAAUGCACAGAGGCCUACCAUAGAGUCAUACAUAUGGUAAAAGAUUGGUAUGUAUUUACUAAUGCAUCCAAUAAUGCAUGCAUUCAUUUUUCCAUCUGGUGACAAUGCUAUUAAAAAUAAGACGUUUCUGGCUGGGUGUGGUGGCUCACACUUGUAAUCCCAGCACUUUGGGAGGCCAAGGCGGGAGAAUCACGAGGUCAGGAGAUCGAGACCAUCCUGGCUAACAUGGUGAAACCCUGUCUCUACUAAAAAUACAAAAAAUUAGCUGGGCAUAGUGGCAGGCACCUGUAGUCCCAGCUACUCGGGAGGCUGAGACAGGAGAAUGGUGUGAACACAGGAGGCAGAGAUUGCAGUGAGCCAAGAUUGCGCCACUGCAUUCCAGCCUGGGCAACAGAGUGAGACUCCGUCUCAAAAAAAUAAAUAAAUAAAUAAAUAAAAAUAAAAUAAAAUAAAAUAAAAAUAAGAUGUUUCUAACAGCCACAUAGAGGCAUUUUACUUUUUGGUAGUUUUUAAAGUAAGGGACAUUUAUUCUCAUAUAUUCCAAGUUCAAAUUAUGCUCCCGUGCUCUAUGAUGCAGAGUUUUGGAAUCCCAAUUCAUCGUUGUCUAAGCAUUUGAGAGGGUCACAUGUACGUUUUCUUUGAGACAAAGAAAUGGCUUUAUCUACAAUCAUGCCUUCAGCCAACCCUCUCUGUGUAGGUGGGAUGGUCCACUAUCUGGGUGAAACACUCAAAUAAUGGUAAUCCCACUGCUUGACAAUGGGUGUCUCAAAUAUCAAGUUAUCUUUGAUGAGCAACAGACAGCAUCUACCUUUUAGGUACUUACCAGAUAGCUGAGUCUUGACACCCCUUCAGCAACUCCCUCAUUGUGUUGACACCAUUGUCAGUAUAAGAGACAGGCCAGCUACCAUCCCCCCAGGUUCUCCAAGCUCUAUUGUUGCCUCUAACUGGCAAUUUAUUCAGACCAUUGUAGUAUCUACGCUUUCUGUGGAAAUGCUUCAAGGGCAUUAGGGCUCUGAUUUUUGUUCUGUCCACAAAAAGACCUGAAUCCAACCAUUGUGAGUGGGGGUGAGGGAUGGGAGUGGAACCAACAUUUCUUAAGCAUCUACUAGCCAGAUACUGUGUAAGAUCCUUUACCUGUGCCAUCUCAUUUAAUCCUCAUGAUAACCUUGAGAGGUGUGUACCAUCACCUCCAUUUUAGAGGUAAGAAAUUAAAAGCUUGAGGUGCUUAAGUAAUUUGUCCAAUGUUGUAGUUCCUAAUCUGAACCCAGUCCUGUCUACUAAAAAGCCCAUAUCCAAAACUUCUGUACUAACUUGCUUCAUGAAGCACUGUUUGUUGUUAUUUAAUGUUUUGUCAAUAUUUGCCCACCUAUUAGUCUAUCUGUAUAUUUCUAUGCAAUAAAUUUUUCCUAAAAUUCAGUCCAGAGAGACCUAUCUUUCUGUGCACUGAUAAUGUUCCUUUUUCUUUGAUGGUGAGGACUAUGUCACUUCUCAUUAUUCUCUUUUUGCUUGACUGCAGAGCCAGAUUGAGUGCUCAAUUGCAGUAAUUCUCAUCUCUGAUAUCUGGUACUAUCACCUCCCUCUUUCUUUUUAGAAUUUCUUAUUGCUGUCUUUUCUCUUUUUUAAACUACUUCUUGAGUUUUCAAAUAUUUCUUAAAAUAAGGUAUAAAUUAUAAAAUCACUAUAACAUUUUUCAAACAGUUAAACAGAUUUUUCAUGUUGGAUGUCAGUUUUACAAUGUGCAGCAGCAGAGAGAUGUUGGAUCCAUUUAAGCAAUAGUUUCUAUGUCCUGUCCUUCCAUUCACAGGUGUGUACAGACACUUACAUGUGCACACACACAGACAUUAGUAGGACAAGCCCCUUGAGGCUCCCAGCCCAUGGCUUCCAUGUGUCUGUCUUGUGUGACCUUAGUCUCACUGACUUUAUUCUAUAAUCGCCUCAUCAGACCAACCAAUCCUUGUAAUUAAUAGGUCACCCAUCCAAAAGACACUUUCCCUUUUGCCUCUCUAGUUUCCUCUUAUGAAAGCAGUUUUAAGAGAGGCAUUUUUCUGAGUGUGUAAAGACUUUAUAUCAGAGCUGCUGCCUUGAAAUUUAGUUUUGAAGAUCAUUGUGGGUGAUCUUUAUUAAGUCUUUCAGGCCUGUAAGUUACUGUUCUAGCUUGGGGCUGGGCUGGAGGGGUAUGGGCGGGGUGGGAAAACUUUGCUCCAUCCAGGGAUGCAAAGUCCAUAGAGUAAUCACGAUGUUUCUUCCUCGUGUGCCCCUCCAAGCUCUGUUGCAAGGGAGACCUAUGUUGCCAGCUUCUCUCUCUCUCAACUUGGUUUUUACACCCAGUGAAUGCAUGGAAGUGUGUGUGUGUGUGUGUGUGUGUGUGUGUGUGUGUGUGUCCGGAAGCGUAAAGAGACAGAUGGUUCUGAAGGCUGGCACAGAGUGGAAGCUUCCUGCUAAACAGAUGUCCCUCUCGGAGUAAUGCAGGCUGCCCAAGAAACCUAUGCUUUUUGGCUCCUGCACCCAUUGCCAAGGGUCGUUCUACUCUCUAAAUAGGCAGCCUGAACUUCAAGUAGAUGGAGGGAAUGUGGGCCAGCCAGAAACCAUCAACAAAUACAAAGGCAUUUUUUUGGCCUGAAUGGUGAUAAAAGUUCAGAAUUGAUGCUUUUUGUUUGUUUUGGACCUAAGAUUUGGUGCCCUUUGCUAGGAGACCAGUUGGCCCGUCAGCUCUCAGCAGCAUUCACUCUGUGUAGCUGUAAAACUCUUCUAGGUUCUUUGGGGAAUUUCAAAGUUGAGUAGAAAAUCUAUUCUUGCCCACGAGGAACUAGCAAUUCAAUAAAUUUUGCCAAAGCCAAAAUCUAGAGGCAAUGAGACUAAAACAAACAAAGCACAACAAUAAAAAACUUGAUGCAAAAAUAGGAACAUAAUAUGAUAAUUAUGUUGUAAUUUUAAACAUAAUUUUAAAAAUGGUUUAGUGUUAAAUGGAUUUAGAUGUAGAGUUGGAAAAAUGUUGAAGAAAUAUUCUCUGCUGUAAAACAGGGCUUCUGGGCAUAGCAGGUUUGGUGGAGGAUGAAUCAUUGCAGGUAGGCGUGCAAGUUUGUGUUUUGGGUCUUCAAAACAAAAAUUGCGUAAUGGACUCUCUUGUCCAUCAAGCAGUUCACAAAAUAGACCUCUGACCAAGAGGGGCUGCAGUGGCUCUCUCCCUUCCUCUUCUCUUCUCACUGUAAUUUUAGGAACCCUUUGGGCAGUAGCUACACCUAUAGUUAAAGGGAAUACAGGAAGUACUCAGGGGAAACAAAAAACUGCCUUUCUGAAUAAAAAUAUGGAAGAGAAGAAAUGUCCAAAAUAGCAUCUGGAAACAAACAUUUUUAUGAAACUAGCAAAGAUGCUUGUCUCCAGGACAGACCUGUUUGGUAUACAAGACUGAAAACAUUUCUAAUUAGUAUUAUCAUGGUCAGUCCUGACCACAUGGGUUUUUUUUGUUCCAUGGUUAAGGACCCAAGUUGUUGUAGAAAGGCUUUUACUACAUUUUCAGUAGGGCCAGGAAUUUUGCUGCAGUAUGGACUUAUUGGUAAACAAGCAUUUGUUAACACCUUCUGCUGUUGUUUUACAAGCCAGGUAAGAGUGGUAACUGAACAGAUAUUCUAUGCAGUUACUCUUUGUAAUUGUGCCGUCACUCUUCCUGGAUUUGCCUAAGGUUAUGAAACUUGGGCUGGAUUCACUUCUUUUGCAGAUAUUUUUUUCACCUUCCGGGGAACUUGUGAAGGUUCCUGAUUCACAGUUUUUGGGCCUGUGAAACUUAAUGACUGAGGGAGAGUGGAAAGUAAUUAGGUUCCUUGCAAUUAUGAUUAUGGUGAGGCUACGAAGAACUCACUUUGCAUAGCCUGCUAUAUAUAGUUCAAGGAAAGCCAUGCCUUCUAUAAUCUCACUUAAAUUUGGCAAUCUUGGGGUGGGCAGGGCAUAUUUAAAAUCUUGCACUUAUCAAAUAAGAAAACUGAGAGGUCAUAGGGUCAUCCGGCUCAUAGAUAGCAAACCUACUUUUAAACCCAGUUUUAUUUCUUAUUCCAAGUUCAAUGCUAUUCCCAUGAAGCACAUGACCUCUUAAAAUUGGUACUUUUUAUUUUGAAAUGCCUCAAUUUUUAGUAUUUAAAAAAGUUUUGGUAUCUUUUUACAAAAAGGUAGUUUUGAGAAUAUGAAUUACACAUCCAGGUGAGAAAACUAAGACAUAAGGAAAUUUGGGGGCUUACUCAAGACCAUAAAAUAAAAUUAGAUAUAGCAUAUCAGGGAAUUGGUGACCCUUUCUACCACACAUUGUGAUUGUUGCUUUGCCUCUGUAUGCAGCUCUCCUUGGGCUUGGUGCACUUGCUACUGCUUUGGUGACUCUCAGGAAAUACAGGAAAAUGGGACUUAUAUAUUAGACUCCAACACUGAUUCAGUAGCAACAUGGAAUUUCCACUUUCUAGUUGCCCUUCAUUGGAGGUUAUUUAUUCUAUCUUCUACACAGGGAAAUUGGGAAGACAUAUGGGUUGUUUGCUUUUUAAAGCACAUACUGCCGAAAAAGGGAAAACCCAGGGCUAUUGCAUAUCGCCAGUUAUAAAAACUUUUGUUGUUGUUAAGGGAUCACUUUAGUUCAUCAUUUUCUUUUUACUGAUGAGGAAGAAACUGAGAAAGAUUAAAAGACGUGUCAAUAUCACAAAGUGAGGAUAAGUUUUAGCAGAGCUUAGGCCUUCUGAUUUUGUUUCAUUCAUUUUUUACUGUAUUUAAUCUUUUGUUUAUGUUGGAAUUCAAGCUAUUUGUUUUUUACUAAUGUUUUCUGUGCUUCUGCAAGAUUUUAUGAGACUCCCCAGUUCAAAAUUUCUUUCCUUAAUUUUCCACACCCAAGCCUUUUAUAUCUAUAACUUUUAUAUUUUGCAAUAAGAAAAAUUAGACUUAUAGAGGCUAUUCAUCCAUCCGCUUGCUUUCUAAUUGAUCACUUAGGAGACUUGUGAUAUGCCCUCCAUCUCUGUGCCUCUCUUUCUUGUUCCCUUCUAACUUACAAUUCCCUGUAACUGCAGCCAUACCCUUCUAGGCUCCCUGUCUGCCCUCCUUAUUCCAGUCAAGCUUGGACUUUGAUCCUUUGCUUAUCCCAGAAUGCUUUGUUCCAAACAUCUUUAAGCCAACCUACUCAAAUGUUAGCCAGAAAACAGCAAUUAUCUAUUGAGCUAAACAUUCAUACUGAAUGAUCAGGAAUGGUAGCGUUAUGAUCAAAUAGGGAGGAAAGUCACAGCUAUUCUCUGAGAGAAAGCUGAGAUAUAUUCACAACAUUGGUUUAUAUUAUCUUAGUGUGAAACCACUUAAAUCUUAACAGUACAUGUUGGGAUGUAUUGGAAGAAAGACAUCACAAAAGUAAUUAUUGACUAUGAAAAGCAUCCAUAAGAAAUGUUUUUAGAGCAACUACUGUAAACUAAUCAGAAUAUAAUUAUUCUAGACAAUACCCCAAGUAGGUGCCGAUCGUUUGAUAUGAGGAUUAGAGAUAAAAACUUCAUUAUGUUCCAUAUAAAAUGCCAGUGCAGAAUGGAAAACAAUAACACUUCAACUAACUAUAUUGAUAUUUAUGCAGUGUCUUCCACCCAAGAUCCUGACAAGUGCUAGUAAGCUAUCAUUAUGUUCUCUGUGUGGCAAUGAACAAUAAGGGUUCAGCAUGUGUUUGUUUAAAAAAGAGUCAUGCUUAUUAAUAUUGAUAGCAUAAUAUUUGGAAACUAUAUUAUUAUGCAGCUAUAAUGUAACCAUUUAUUCUGUUCUGCUAUCAAGCCAUUGAAACUGAGCUCUGCCCAAUGACUGCAUUUGCUUGACUUAGGGUUGCUGUACUUAUUUGUUGGAGGUACCCUCCCAUAUGUACCCUCCUUCAGACCUCACCAGCCUAUGGAUGCAACAUGAACCACAUCAAGGGAAUUCACAUUUCCCUGGCUUACAUCCCACUGAGGUCUCAGCAUCACAUCCCUGCCCUCCAACAAAGCCUUUCCUCAUUUGUUUGGGAAGUCCCAGGAGUGUCUCAUAUGUGAUCACAAAUCAUAGUUUUCCUCUUUGAACCCACCUUUCCCUGAUGUCCAAGGCACUUGGAAACACCAGGUACUGGUGCCUCCUUCAUUGUUGCCACCAUGGCUGGUAUCCUCUUUAGGAACAUUGCUUCCUUGGCUAGAUAUGGACUCCUGGUGUGGUCCCUUGGGUGUCACUGAGCUGGAGCCAUGUGUGUUUUGUGCACACACAGGAAGUGUUUCACUCCUAUGCUUGCUCAUACCCAGGAUAUCCUUGUGAAACCACAGCCUCAGUACUGCUCUUCUCCCUACUGGGCUUGGGCCUGGUGCAUGGGAUCCCACUGGGGAACAAGUCAUUCUCUUUAUGCUCAUCCCUGCAACCAAGUCCUUUUUCAGGCCAUGCUGAUCAGCUCACGGAAACAGAAGCCUCCCUCUCCCUUUUCCAGAUUAACCCAGAUAGGUCUGGAACCAAUAGGAACCCGCUAACAUAUUACCAGCUAAAAACAAUAGCUUUGCGUCUGUUAGGAUAAACACAAUGAUUCACACUGCAGAAUUGGUGUGCCAGAAUUUUUGCAGGCUGUGUCCAGGGAAAAGGAAGCAGGUUGUUAAGUAUGCUACUAGUAGAAAAAUAAAACAAACCACUGUUUAUUGAGUUCUUCCUAUUCACUAGGCCAUGUAUUUACUACUUACUGGCUUUAUACAUACCACACACAUACGCAUAUACACAGACAUACACAUACUUUAUUUAAUUCUUCAACCCUACAACAGAGGUCAUUUUUUCCAUAGGCCAAGAUAGGUAACAGGUGCAGAAAGCCAAUGGAGGAAUGGAAGGGAGCCAUUAUUUACUGAGCACCUGCUCGGUCCCAGGCUUUACGGAGGUGCAUUGCAUAUGCUGUUUUACUUCAUCCUCACAGUGCUCCCAAGCCAUUCCCCUUCUGCAGGUAACUAUGUGAAGGCAAAGAGAACAUAAUUUCUUGAUGACUGCAGAGCUAGUAACUGGUAAAUCUGACAUGACCCUAGUCUGUUUGAGUUCAAAGCCCUAGCUCUUUCCUUUGUAUAGCACGAGAGCCUCAGAGACAUUGCUUGACUCUGUCCCUACCACCUCAUUUCCAAUCUUUGCCUCAGAGGGCCUAACCUCGUUUUACAUCAUCAGAACCAGAGCUCUGAAUUUGACCAUUGCCCAGUGUUUCCUCAAAGAGAUGUUUAAUAGGCUUUUGAGGGCUAGCCUGAGAAUGUAGGCACUAUUAACUCUCAUUUCUAUAGGAAGAUAUAUGUCACAUUCCAAUUAAGUGGCUUACAAAUUGAGUAUGUAACACAUUCAAAUGCAUAUGACAUAUAUGUAAUAACCUUUGAAAAUUUGUAAGUUGGAUAUUUAUAGCAUUAAAAUAGUUAAAUUUAUUAAAAAUAAAAAUGUUUCCAUUAGUGUUCCUGUCUUUAUUAGUCAAGUAAGAGGACUGAGGAGCUAGAAACCUUAUUUGCUAUCCACAUUUGCUAUCCAGCUUGGAGUUGCUGGUAAAAGUUCCUCUGUGUGAGGAAAAAAUGUGGUAGUUUAAGCAUGAAAUAAAUAUUGUAAGAUCACAAUGAUCUAUUGAAUUUUUAAGUACAAUUAUAAUUUAAAUUCAUUUUUUUCCUGUAUCUUGCUGCUCUAUGUGAAUCUCCAGCAGAGGAUAAUUUAAUCUUGAAGCUGAAUUAAGUUUCAUAGUAACCCUUACCAAAGCAGAUAAUUUCUCUUUACAUAGAGCAGAAUUCAAGCAAAUUUGUAUUAAUUUUGGUUGUGAAAAGUAUCUCUCUGCUGUUGCAACUGUGACUGACAUUAUUUUAAUGAUUCUCAAAAUCAAACAAAUAUUGAGGUUUUUAUGUUUUUUUGUUUUUUUAAAUCGAACCCCAGCUUAGAAUUGAGAGUGUGGGUUAGCCAUCCUUCUUCUGGGAAGUCUAACCUAGCCCAUUCCUAUUGUAUUAGUCUAGUCUCAUGCUGCUCAUAAAGACAUACCCAAAACUGGGUAAUUUAUAAAGAAAAAGAGGUUUAAUGGACUCACAGUUCCACAUGGCUGGGGAGGCCUAACAAUCAUGGCGGAAGGCGAAUGAAGAGCGAAGUCAUGUCUUACAUGGCAGCAGGAAAGAAAGCUUAUGUGGGGGAACUCCCAUUUAUAAAACCAUCAGAUCUCAUAAGACUUAUUCACUACCACAAGAACAGCAUGGGAAAGACCCGUCCCCAUGAUUCAAUUACCUCCCACCAGGUCCCUCCCAUGACACAUCAGAAUUAUUACAAUUCAAAGUGAGAUUUGGAUGGGGAUACAGAGCCAACCAUAUCACCCAUCAACCCACCAGUUUAGGGGCCUUCCUGUUUGCUCCCCAGGGGCCCUGCACUAAUGCCCAUGUCUCCCAUAGCACAUGUGACUGUAGCUGCUUUUCUGUUCAUCCACAUCCCCCACUGGACUGCAAGUUCCUUUCAGGAGGGAAGGACUGCUUUGGAUUCACUCCCUUCCCUGUGCCCGGCACAGUGCCUAGUCCUCAAUAAGUAGUUAAUGAAUAAUUGAAUUGGUGAAUGGCUAAGUUAUUCCCUUGUUUUUCUAGUUGAGGGAUGAAAUGUGAGUUUUGGAUAAGAUAGGUAACUUGCUUAUGAUUGUGUAAGUAGUAAAUGACAACACAGGCAAGAUAAAGUGCCUGCCCAGGAGAAAGCUGAGACAUAGACACAGCUAGUCACCGCAGUUAUCGUAGCCAGGGAGAGCAAAAGACAGUUAACCAAUCGGAGGCUAACUAUAGCUCUAAUGAGUGACGUUAUGGGGUCUCAUAAAAGGGAAAAGAGAACAAGGAAGACACUGAAUUCUUUCUGGGUUAGCAGAGACACCCAAGUGUAAGAAUGUAGAAAGUGUUUGAGAAACCACUUGACUGAAGGCAAAAACCUCAUUGUUGUGCAUAUAUAUACGCCAAAUGGAAGAAGAAAAAUUAGAUAAAAGUUUCAGGUUAGGGUGUGUAUGUAGAUAUAUAAUAUAUCAUGUAUGUAUGUAAUGUAUAAAACCUGAUAUGCAUAUUUAUGGAAAUGUUCUGGGUUUGAUGGUGGAAAAAUCAUUGAAAACAAGUAGCUGGCAGUAACAGCAGACAUUUACUGAGUAUGUAUACUGGGACUGAACUACUUACUGGGCUGGGAGGAGAUACAGAAAUUAGAGCCAUUCUGUCAUUGAUCUUAAGGAGACUUUAGCCAGAGAAGGAGGAUAUGACCUUAACACAAAUGAAAAUAAAGCAAAGUGAGGGAAAUAUAAGUAAAGUCCAAAAUAUCAUUAUUAUUUUGUAUUAUUUAUUUGUGUUUGUCUUCUUUCUUUUCUUUUCCUCUUUCUUUCUCUUUCUCUUUCUUUCUUUCUUUGUUUCUUUCUCUCUCUCUUUCUUUCUUCUCUAUUUUUUCUCUUUCUUUCCUUUCUCUCUUUCUCUCUCUCUCUUUUUUUUUUUUUUUUUUUUUUUGAGAAGAAGUUUCACUCUUGUUGCCCAGGCUGGAGUGCAAUGGUUUAAUCUUAGCUCACCACAACCUCUGCUUCCUGGGUUCAAGUGAUUCUCCUGCCUCAGCCUCCCGAGUAGCUGGGAUUACAGGCAUGUGCCACUACGCCCAGCUAAUUUUUGUAUUUUUAGUAGAGACAGGGUUUCACCAUGUGCGCCAGGAUGGUCUCAAUCUCCUGACCUCAUGAUCCGCCCGUCUCACCCUCCCCAAGUGCUGGGAUUACAGGCGUAAGCCACUGUGCCAAGCCUGUAUUUAUUUGUUUUUAUAAGAGACAGGGUCUCACUCUGUUGUCCCCAGGCUGAACUGGAACUCCUGGGCUCAAGCCUGAUUCUCUUGCUUCAGUCUCCCAAGUAGCUGGACUACAGGCACAUGCCACUACACCAGGCAGUAAGGUCCAAAAUAAUCAAAUUAAAAAAAAUUAUAGAGGCCCAAAUGUUUGAGAAACUAUAUGCAGUUAAAAAUAUGUUAAAGAUGAUUCUUGAAGGAUAAGGCAGAAUUUCAACAGGUAAAGGUGGAAUAGAGGAGGCAGGUAAGGUAAAGUCAUCUUUUGAGUGGUUAGGAUUUGUAAAUAACAUAGAAACCUUUAAAAGUGACUUAUACAUGUUGGCAUUAUUACCUUUGGUCAUGGCUCUGGCUGGAAACCAAGGCAGGCCCAAGGGUUUAACUUAGGGCUAUUGAUGAAGGUGCUCUUUACUGUAGGCGUCUGGGCAGAGUGGACAGAAUCCAAAGCCUUGUAAGGCCCCCAGAGACUGGCAACAGCAGGGGGUUGUUGCCACCACUGGGGGGCCUGACCCAGCAGGGCAGAGGGUGAAGCCACAGUGGGACGGGCAGGGCUGGAGGCAAGAUAUUGCUUAUGAGACAAGCCAUCCCACCUGUCACUGUCAGCCCCAGUGUGAGCUUCCUAUGGUCCACAAGUGCCUCAUCUACCCUAACUUCCUUCCCUUUCUACUUUCUGAUCUGCUGAUGCCUCCAACAGAAACUCAACAGGAAGCCAGAGGGCCAGAGAGCCAGCGAUGGCCCAUCCACAGUCACCCCCAGGCACAGAGAAGGGUGGAGAACAGAUCCAGGGUAGCUGAGAAUAACCAACACAGACACAUAGCACUUUCUACCAAUUCCAGCCUUAUACUGAAAGUUCAUUACAGUUUUCCGCACCAGAGAAUUCAGCAAAAGACAGCUCUGUAUUGGAUAUCAUUCAGAGGGAUUUUAUUACUGACAGUACCAGAAAUAACUUCUUUUAAGUCCUACUUUGUGUGCUUCUAACGAUAUAACACUGUUCUCUAAGAAAAACAAAAAACACAUAGUGAUGCUAAAUAAGUUGGUUUUAUUAGGGAAGGGGAUAUUUUAUUAUCCAAGACCCUGGCCUUUCAUUUCACCUGGGUGCUUUUCAGAGCUAGGACUCAGAGAACAAAGCUCUGUGAGGAGACUGCAGCUGGAGACUUUUUCUUACUUUCUAAGUUCAUUCUUUUCUCUUUAGGCUUGUGGGUGGUUUCCUUUAUAAGCCAUUUUAGAAGUUCUGGGUCUCCACUGCUCCUGAGGUGACCAGACUUUCUGGAAAAUGGAGGCUGAGGCAGGAUGAUGAGCUCAGCUGGGUGGGCCCUCAUCCUGUCCUGAUUCCUAAGCACUGCUGGGAGUAAAUCCUUUAAAUUGCACAUCACAUUUGCAUCUCUCUGUUUACAUUUCUUAAUUUCCUCAAGAAUCGUUUGUUUGUCGAGAGCUGGUUGUUUCUUUAGCAAAGAUUUCCUGAAUAAACAAUGUAAAGAGCCUUCUUUUUUAAAAACACCGCUCCACUAAAUAAACAAAUACAGCAAUGAAUAAAUAAAGGAAAUAUCUAGUAGGUUAAUCCUAGUCCAUGCAAACAUGUUUUCUUCCACACAGCUGACUAAAGGCAUAGAUUCAAUAGAAUUCAAGUAGUUCUGACUCAUGCUCAUUUAAUUUAAUCAGCAUUGACCAUAUGUUUGGAGUUUGUCUUAAAACAGAAGCGUUUCUUCCUAGUUUUGUGUGUGUAUGUGUGUGUGUGUGUGUGUGUGUGUGUUCGUGUUCAAUGAAAACUCUAUAAGUGUUAUAGACUAUUUUCAGCUAAAAACCUUCCCCUCUCCUGGUUAGUUUCCUAAUGUUGUUGCAGCAAAUUAUCACAAACCAGGUGGCUUAAAACAAAUUUUUUCCCUCACAGUUCUGGAGGCCAGAAGUCCAAAAUCAAGGGGGUUAGUGGGACCAUGCUCCUUCCAUCGACCCUGGGGAAGAACCUUCCUUGCCUCUUCCCAGCAUCUGGUGGCUCCUGGCAAUCUUGAUAUUCCUUGGCUUCUGGUCUCAUCACUCAGGUCUCUUCCUCCUGCUUCACAUGGCCUUCUCUCUGUGCCCUCCCCACUUCUUAUUAGGAUAUCAGUUAUUGGAUUUAGGGCAUCCUAAUCCAAUAUGAGCUCAUCUGGAUCCUUAAUUAAUUAUAUAUGCAAAAAUCCAGCUUCCAAAUAAGGUCACUGUACUGGGUUAAAAAAAUGUCCCCACCAAAAUUCAUAUCAACCCAGAACCUCAGAAUGUGACUUUAUUUGGGAAUACAGUCUUUGCAGAUAUAACUAGUCAACAUGAGGUCAUCCUGGAUUAGAGUGGGUCCCAAAUCCAAUGACUGGUGUCUUUACAAGAUCGGAAGAGGCCAUAGGGAGAAGAAAGCCAUGUGAAGUAGGAGGAAGAAAUUGGAGUCAGACAGCUACAAGGCAUGGAACAUGAAGAAUUGUCAGAAACCACCAGAAGCUAGGAGGAGGCAAGGAAGGAUUCUUCUCAACAGCCUUCAGAGAAGGUGUCCCAUAAACACCUUGAUUUUGGACGUCUAGUUCCCAGAACUGUGCAAGAAUAAAUUUCUGUUGUUGUAAACCACUAAAUUUGUGUUAAUUUGUUAUGGCAGUCCUGAGAAAAUAAUUCAAUCACUCUUAAGUUUUCCAGGUAGAUGUGAAUUUUGGUGGUAUACUAGUCAAUCCACUUCACCCUAACUGUGAGGGGAGUUGGCCAAUGUCAUUCUACCUGUUAUGCAAAUGAGGAGCAAGGUGCUAGGGGAAGGGGCAGAGCAGGAAACUGAUUUCACUUUUAAAAAACAUUAUUGUGGCACUAUUCACAAUAGCAAAGACUUGGAACCAACCCAAAUGUCCAUCAAUGAUAGACUGGAUUAAGAAAAUGUGACACACAUACACCAUGGAAUACUAUGCAGCCAUAAAAAAGAUGAAUUCAUGUCCUUUGCAGGGACAUAGAUGAAGCUGGAAACCAUCAUUCUCGGCAAACUAUCACAAGGACAGAAAACCAACCACCACAUGUUCUCACUCAUAGGUGGGAACUGAACAAUAAGAACACUUAGACACAGGGCGGGGAACAUCACACACUGGGACCUGUCGGGGGCUGGGGGUUGGGGGAGGGAUAGCAUUAGGAGAAAUACCUAAUGUAAAUGACGAGUUGAUGGGUGCAGGAAACCAACAUGGCACAUGUAUAGCUAUGUAUCAAACCUGCAUGUUGUGCACAUGUUCCCUAGAACUUAAAGUAUAAUAACAAAAUAAAUAAAUAAUAAAAAACGUAUUAAAGUUCAAUUCUCUUUUUUCUUGGAGAUAAAAAGAUUUCUCAAGGUUCCUGGAAAGCCACUUUUUGGGGGCCAAUCAUAAAUAUAAUUUAACAGAUUAUAUAAAUAGCCCUACUAUUUAAAAAAAUGUAGACCCCUUUAGUGCUUUUAUAGAGCUCUGAGCAAAGAAUUGUAAGAAAACUCCAUGCCUUCCCUAUGAUGAUCUGGUCUUAUUUCAUGACUGCUAUGGUACUGCUUACUAGUCUACUCUUGGCCCUUGUCCGUGCGCUGAUAAACCUUUCAUGGUAUGCACUCACUCAUGGCUUGAUGGUGUCUGGAUAGCAGAUUCCCAGGGUUUGUUCUUUAGGCGUCAAUUUUUAUAAUUAUUUCCUUACAUUUUGCUCUCUUUUACUUUGAGGAAAGGUCGUGUUUCCUUCAGAGUAGCUAAGGCAUGGACCUAGGGUAGGAGGUUUCAGGAAUUGCUACUCUGAAGGACGAUGUUUUCUGUCAUCUUCCUAGAUUUCCAACCUGGGGCUUUCAGAUUCCAAUUUGUUAGUUUGCUGGAAUUCUUACAGAGGAAAAGGAGGUUAUGGUUCCACAUGGCAAGAUCAUUUGUGUCAACAUUUAAUUUAACAGUCAAUGUUUUUGUUAACUGAGGUAACAGACAAUCUGCAAACAGAAUAAAUUUUUAAAAGAUUACUCCAUCAAAGGGGACCUUCCUCAGGAAUUAUUUUCUAGAAUUCUCUAUCUAGACUGGUGAUCUUCUAAAUCUUCUAGGCAAAACCACUUAUGUAAUUUGCAGAGCCCAGUGUGCACGCAGUGAAAAUUUGGGUCUCCUUGUUCAAAAAACAUAAAAAGGGGACCAUGGCCCUUCAAGCAUGAAAGAGUGAUACCUUUGUUGGGCGUGUGGUGAGAGGAUCCCAGGGAAAGAGAAAACAAGGAGCGACUUUGAGGCACUGUGGGUGGUGAACUGCAUCCAGAUGAUCUAGCCCAGCAGUCUCCAACUUUUUGGCACCAGGGACCCAUUUUGUGGAAGACAAUUUUGCCACGGAUGGCAGGGGGAUGGUUUUAGGAUGAAACUGUCCUACCUCAGAUCAUCAGGCAUUAGAAUCUCAUAAGGAGUGUGCAAUCUAGAUCCCUCAUGUGCACAAUUCACAGUAGGGUUCGUGCUACUAUGAGAAUCUAAUGCCUCAGUUGAUCUGACAGGAGCCAGAGCACAGGCUGUCUUGCUCGCUUGCCAGCUGCUCACCUCCUGCUGUCUGGUUCCUAACAGGCCAUUGACUGCUACCAGUCUGUGGCCUUGGGUUUGCGGACCCCUGAUCUAGCCCUUUCCUCUCCACCUCUAUCAUACCGCCUUCAGGUACUCUUCCUCCUCCUGCUCUUUUGAACGUGCCUCACACCCCUUUAUUUUCCAGCCCUUUUGCUCCCUUUCUCCUCCCACAUUCCUUCAUUUGGGCAGCCUGCAGCAUCUUUGACCUACUCCACCCCACAUCUCUCCUUCACUCUGCCAGUUCAUAUGGUCAGGCCUGGAUUCAACAGCCCGAGCUCAGAAGAGCCCCUGCAUGUGAUCUGAUGCUCUCAUGUUGCCGUCUUGAAAUUCUUAAUACUUUUUUAGUUGGUUUUACAAAUAAGUGAAGUGGUGGAAUGAUAAAUCAGAGGGUUUUAAAAUUUGCAAGUUAAUGCUCAUGUUGCAUGAAAGAAAUACACAGGUAUUUGCACAAUGCUUUGAGACACUAAAGGUCUGUGCAGCCACGGCAGUAUCCUUCCCUGUAAACCAUGGUGAUUUUUUAAAAAAAAUUAUUAUUUUUUUUAGAGGCAGGGUCUUGCUCUGUCACCCAGGCUGCAGUGCAAACAUGGUGCUUUUGAUUCUCAUUUGACUUUUGCAGGAACAUUUGUUUCACUUUCUAAUAUCAACGAAAUGUUUGGAGUUCUCAGUUGUGAUAGUGAAUGGCAUGCAUCAUUCAGUGCAUUUGCUAUUGUGUCAGAUUUUCUGUGGUGUUUUAGGGAGUCAUCCAUGAAUUGAUCUUAAAUGAGGGCUGGAUAUGUAUCUCCCUCCUCCUGAGCUUCCCCAACUCUCCUGAUUUGGGUCUCAUUUCCUGUCUUUUAUGUAGAAGCUUUCAUAAGACUCUACUUUGAUCAUUCAUUGUCUUAGGAAAUUUGAGUUCACUAAGGAGUGUGUAGGCAUUAGAACUUCAUUGUUCCCAUCUUUGAGUCUGUGUAACCAGGAGUAAUUGGGAGAUGUUUCUGUCAUCACUUAGCCCUGGAGCAAUUUGUACUCUGACUUCAAGAGAGUAUGACAAGGAUAGUUACAUGGAGAGGGGGAUGGGUUUAGAAUAUUUUAAUUGCUAUUCUAGUACAUGUCAGUAUGACAUGAUCUGCAAAAGGAAAUUUCCCUAACGAUUUUAAGUCUGUACCAGUUGCAUUUUGUUCAUUCAGAAGAGCUAUGAAGCAAUGUGGAUUCCCAUUUUCUCAGAUAGUAGAUUUUAUAUAAUUUUUUUGGCAUGGAGCUGUAUAUGGAGAGAGGAGCUAACUGGUCAGCCUGAAUAUGCCUCAAGUUUAUGCAAAUUUCUCAAAGCCCAUGGGGUUCAACAAUAUCUUAUGAAUUGUUUCUUUUUCUAUUUUACUUUUUUAUUUCCAACUUUUGAUUUUGAUUUUUUUUCAAACAUGUGGGCAAGUUCAAAAGAUUAGUAUAAUGAACACCUACACUUGCCAUCUAGAUUCUACAAUUGUUAUAGUGAGUUGGUUCUUGACUCCAAUUAGGCACUUUUUGCGUUUUAUUCACAGGCCCCUUUCAAAACCUAUUGGUUUUGGCUUGUCACUCAGAUUUUCCCAAACUGAGAGGGACCCAUUAACUUCUGUUUUUAUGCUAAAAAAAAAGAGGAAAUUAAAAAAAUCAUAGAACCUUCCCUAUUAGUGUUGUUGAUGACAGUAUUGAUUCUUGUGUAAAUUGGAUUUACCUUUAUCCUUUCAUCUUCCUUUUUAUAGGCUAUUGAGAGUUUACUGUCAUGCCUACCUGAGCACAGGAGUUUGGCAUUAAAUUCAUGGUUUGUAACUUAACCAUUGCUACUUACAGAACAAAACAACUGGAUGAAUAUCACAUGGAACUAUUUUUCAUUCUUUCGAGUUCACACCGAUGUGCUUGUUGAGAAAGAGAAACAUCUGAAACACAGGCCCCUUGGUGUAACAUCAGUGACAACACUGCCUGUCUAGGGAACCUCGACUGGAUGGCUGCCAGCUCAGGGGUGCAGUUGAGAACGAUUCCUGGGUCGCUGUUGACUCCUUGGAGGAGACAUUUCAUGCCCACAUAACUCUAGAUAUUUGCUGAUGGAAAGCACAGUGCUCUACUGUGCACUUCAAGUGGAAUAUCAUGCAGAUAGCAGUGAAUUGCAUCAUGCAGAUUAGAAGGGGGGUUAUCUAAGGUAGCAUAACAGCCUCUUUUGAAGGCACUGAAAAAAUAUAUAUUUGGGAAUAGUGUUGGCAUACAGCACCUAGAACAAAGUCUCACAUGUAAACCAUGCUCAGAGAAUGUUCUAUUUAACUUCGUCUGUAAGAUAUGAAACUGUCUUUUUUCUUUCUCAUAUUUAACUUUCAGUUAUAAAGCUUUCUAAAUUGCUUUGAUAAUAUUCAAAGAUAUAGGCAGAUUAACACUUUCUCUGUUAUUUCCUCUUUCAUGUGUGUUGACACAUACAACUAUAUGUGUGUAGUGUUAUAUAAGUGUCAACUACUUAAGUGAAGAAAGUAGGUAUGGCUGUCUAGAAAAAGUGCUUUAAAAGUGGGAAGACAUACUUUUAAAGCUAAAGCAGUGACAAGAUUUUGUCAUUUGAAAUAGUGGGAUAAACUGUAGAUCAUAAUUCAUAAAUUCUUUAUUCUUAAAGAGUAAAAAUAUUAAUGAUGAAAAUCCAGGGAGAUUUGUUUAGGCUCAUGGAUCUAUUGAACCAUUUCAGUAGAAAGGAGAUUAAUUACAGUUGAAAUUUCAUUAACACACAUUUUAAUAAUUAAAAUAUAUGAAGUGAUAUGUUAAGUGAAGAUGUGAUAUAAAUCGUCAAACUUUAUUUACGACCUUAUCUACCAAACCUCAAAUUCUAUAAAAUUUCAAACUCUAUAAAUUGGUAGGUAUAUAAGUACACAAAUGCAAAACUUGAGAUUUAAAAAUUCUUUUCUAUGCUUCACAUCCCCAGAUUUAUAUAGGUAAUAUUAUAAUGGUAAUAUUCUUGACUAUAGCCUGACAUAGCUUAUUAUAAUAAGAUUGAGUUAACAAGGUAGUGUGUAGUUACAAGAAUAACUUAAAUAUUCUUGAUGGGUUUAUAGAUUAGGAGAAAAGACUUUAAGAGUCAUAGCCUUAAGAGUCAAUAUGGUAAGUGAAAUGAUGGCUCUCCACAGUUGUCCACAUCCUAAUCCCUGAAAUCUAUAAAUGCUGCCUGAUGUGGCAGAAGGGACUUUGCAUGUGUGAUUGAGUUAAGGGUCUUGAGAUAGGAAGGUCAUCCUGGAUCAUCUGGGUGGGCCCACCAUCAUCGCAGGGCUGCUUAUAAGUGAGAGGCAGGAGAGCCAGAGACCAAGAGAGAUUUGAAGAUGCCCUACUGACUGGCUUUAGAAUGGAAGAAGGGGCCACAAGCCCAGGAAGGUGGGUGGUCUCCAGAAGAUUGAAAAGGCAAGGAAACUGAUUCUCUCCUAGAGCCUCCAGAAGGAAUGCUGCCCUGUAGACAUCUUGAUUGUAGCCCUGUGAGACCCAUUUUAGACUUCUGACCUCCAGAACUAAGAGAAGAAAUUUGUGUUGUUUUAAGCCACUAAGGUGUGGUAUUUGUUAAGGCAGCAACAGGAAACUGACAUAGUCAGGAAGCAAGUUGGUCACAGGUGGAACUAUGUCUUUGAUCAGGAGAGUGAGAACCUGCUUGUGAUCAUUUCCUAGAGUAUUAACCAAAAAGUCUUAUGAAAUGUGGAAAAAAUAGCAAUCUUGUGACCCAGGAUUUACUGAAGCCCUUGGAAUUCAACACUCAGAGGUGUUAGGCAAAUCCAAAGUACUUUUAUCAAAAUUAGUCACCACAAUUAUGUUAGUAGAUGGAAAUUAAGCUGGAAUUUAAAUCAUUCUGCACAGGAUAAAGCUUUAACUUCCAUAUUUCCUGAAAUUAAAUAUUAUUCUAAAAAUAAUUACUUCCUGAAUUAUUAAUCCCUGAUAUUUAAGGACUCACUUUUUAUCUAUGGCUUGCCUGUAACCUUGUAAUAAAGUGGACCUGGCCCGCUUUGUGCUGGGGUAUGUACUAGCAGAAUGCUAGAUUGAAUUGCUAGAAAAAAGCCAGCCAACAGUUUGGCUGGAAGACCAGUCAUCUGCAGAGCACACCAGAGCUGACAGCCAUGGGGCACCUCCUUUCUGGAGUCUGCACAAGUGUGAAAAAGGCUACUUUAUGCUAAAGGAGCCCUUUUCCUGGAAUAUUUACUUAGGCCUCCAUCUCCCCAUGAUGAUUUACAUGUUAUUUCUCACCCCUGCUGUCAGGAUAAAAUGAGUAUUUUGAGGUCUCAUGAUCUGAAGAGUGUUGGUACUACCUGUCACCUGUCAGGAAGAUGGAUACCAGCAUCUGCUGUAGUUGUUGACUUGUAUCAAAAUAACCACACAGUACUUGGGUACAGUGAAUUCUGCUCCUUCUUUGUUUCCUUGGCUAGUGCUUAAGAUAAAAAAAGUACAUUAUUCUUUGUAUUUUUCUAGUAGCAUUCACUUGGAUCUUUCAAAGCAAAACCUGCAAAUGUUUUUACUUUCAUGAAGCUAGUAAGUAUAGGAAUUGUUGUCUUCUUAAUAGUAUAGUGCUUACAUAUGUGGGCUCUGGAGCCAGACUGCGUGGGUUUGAAUCCUGGCUCUGCCAUUUACUGGCUGUGUGACCUUGGGCAAGUUCCUUUACCCCUCCCUGUGGCUGUUUCCUCAAAAGGGGCAUAAUGAUAUUUUCUAUCUCAUAAGAUUGUUUGAGGGUGAGAUGAAUUAAUAUGUGAAAAACACCUAGAGUAGUACGUAGCACAUUUUAGUAAAAUAAUGACUAUGUAUUUACUUGAAUUAUUUAAUUCUUAUAACCUCCAUAUAAUGAGUUACGGGUGAUUUUUAUUCCAUUUUAGAGAUAGAAACCAUGGCAUGGAUAACUGGUCCAAUUCUCAUGGUUGAUUACGGUCUUUGGUCAAACAAUUAGAGAGAGGGGAAGCUUCAGUGGUAGAUCUUAAGAAGAAUUUGGAAUAUGCAGCCACAGUGCUUGAAUCUGUGUAUAUUGAUGAAACAAGGAGACUCCUGGAUACAGAGGAUGAGCUCAGUGACAUUCAGUCAGAUGCUGUGCCUUCUGAGGUCCGAGACUGGCUGGCCUCCACCUUCACGCGGCAGAUGGGGAUGAUGCUCAGGAGGAGCGACGAGAAGCCCCGGUUCAAGAGCAUCGUUCACGCAGUGCAGGCUGGGAUAUUUGUGGAGAGAAUGUAUAGACGGACAUCAAACAUGGUUGGACUGAGCUAUCCACCAGCUGUUAUUGAGGCAUUAAAGGAUGUGGACAAGUGGUCCUUUGACGUCUUUUCCCUCAAUGAGGCCAGUGGGGAUCAUGCACUGAAAUUUAUUUUCUAUGAACUACUCACACGUUAUGAUCUGAUCAGCCGUUUCAAGAUCCCCAUUUCUGCACUUGUCUCAUUUGUGGAGGCCCUGGAAGUGGGAUACAGCAAGCACAAAAAUCCUUACCAUAACUUAAUGCACGCUGCCGAUGUUACACAGACAGUGCAUUACCUCCUCUAUAAGACAGGAGUGGCGAACUGGCUGACGGAGCUGGAGAUCUUUGCUAUAAUCUUCUCAGCUGCCAUCCAUGACUACGAGCAUACCGGAACCACCAACAAUUUCCACAUUCAGACUCGGUCUGAUCCAGCUAUUCUGUAUAAUGACAGAUCUGUACUGGAGAAUCACCAUUUAAGUGCAGCUUAUCGCCUUCUGCAAGAUGACGAGGAAAUGAAUAUUUUGAUUAACCUCUCAAAGGAUGACUGGAGGGAGUUUCGAACCUUGGUAAUUGAAAUGGUGAUGGCCACAGAUAUGUCUUGUCACUUCCAACAAAUCAAAGCAAUGAAGACUGCUCUGCAGCAGCCAGAAGCCAUUGAAAAGCCAAAAGCCUUAUCCCUUAUGCUGCAUACAGCAGAUAUUAGCCAUCCAGCAAAAGCAUGGGACCUCCAUCAUCGCUGGACAAUGUCACUCCUGGAGGAGUUCUUCAGACAGGGUGACAGAGAAGCAGAGCUGGGGCUGCCUUUUUCUCCUCUGUGUGACCGAAAGUCCACUAUGGUUGCUCAGUCACAAGUAGGUUUCAUUGAUUUCAUCGUGGAACCCACCUUCACUGUGCUUACGGACAUGACCGAGAAGAUUGUGAGUCCAUUAAUCGAUGAAACCUCUCAAACUGGUGGGACAGGACAGAGGCGUUCGAGUUUGAAUAGCAUCAGCUCGUCAGAUGCCAAGCGAUCAGGUGUCAAGACCUCUGGUUCAGAGGGAAGUGCCCCGAUCAACAAUUCUGUCAUCUCCGUUGACUAUAAGAGCUUUAAAGCUACUUGGACGGAAGUGGUGCACAUCAAUCGGGAGAGAUGGAGGGCCAAGGUACCCAAAGAGGAGAAGGCCAAGAAGGAAGCAGAGGAAAAGGCUCGCCUGGCCGCAGAGGAGCAGCAAAAGGAAAUGGAAGCCAAAAGCCAGGCUGAAGAAGGCGCAUCUGGCAAAGCUGAGAAAAAGACGUCUGGAGAAACUAAGAAUCAAGUCAAUGGAACACGGGCAAACAAAAGUGACAACCCUCGUGGGAAAAACUCCAAAGCCGAGAAGUCAUCAGGAGAACAGCAACAGAAUGGUGACUUCAAAGAUGGUAAAAAUAAGACAGACAAGAAGGAUCACUCUAACAUCGGAAAUGAUUCAAAGAAAACAGAUGGCACAAAACAGCGUUCUCACGGCUCACCAGCCCCAAGCACCAGCUCCACGUGUCGCCUUACGUUGCCAGUCAUCAAGCCUCCUUUGCGUCAUUUUAAACGCCCUGCUUACGCAUCUAGCUCCUAUGCACCUUCAGUCUCAAAGAAAACUGAUGAGCAUCCUGCAAGGUACAAGAUGCUGGAUCAGAGGAUCAAAAUGAAAAAGAUUCAGAACAUCUCACAUAACUGGAACAGAAAAUAGGCCGAGGGGAAGAAGAGAGGGAGUGAAGGAGGGUCUACCUAUCUGCUUCUCAGCACCCACUGGCCACAGCAGGACACACCUCCAAGACCCUUGGAGGCUGUUGGAGCAGGUACUAUCCUGGUUGACUCCACCAAGGUGAAAUGAAAGUUGUAUGUGAUUUUCCUCUUUGUUGUUCUUGUAUAGACUUUUCAAUUGCUGUAUGUGGGAUCAGCCCAGACGCCAGCAACAAACUAGCAAGAGGGGUGUUUUUAUGGUAUAAGUCUCUAAAAGUCUAAAUUGGACCAAAAUUAAAAUGACACAAACUUAAAAAAAAAUAAAAUUCCUCUCAUUGCCACUUUUUUCAAUCUCUAAAAGUUAGUUGCCCCCAAAAGAAUAUUGGUUUAAUAAUCAUCAUAUUUAAGAAAUGCACUGAUAAAAACAUAUUUUCCAAUUUUAAAUACACCUAUUUAAAAUGUAAAUACACUUAUUUAAAAUUCAAGUAAAUAUGUAACUAUCAAAGUAAAUGUAUUCAAAACAGAAGUUGUGCUUCUGAAUGUAAAAAUAUUAAAAGGAAGAGAAGACGGAUGAAUUGUUGUAUUCAUGGACAUUUCAGAAUUCACGCUUAUAAAGCAAAUCCAAGUUAAAAAACAAAAAAAGAUUUUUGUGCCUCAUGAAGAUUGUGCCUCAUGCCCAAUAACCUCAUGUACUUUGAAGGAUGUGAAGGUUUGCAAGAGAUGCAUUUGGCUUCAUUUUCCUCUAAUCUUUUACUUCUACCCACAGUAGAUGAUACAAAAAAUCUUGCCUUAAAGACUGCAGGUUUAAGAGUCAUUGCAAAAGAUGUCAGUUUGAUUUUGUGGUCCUAGGCCAAGAGGGUGUAAAAUUCUGAGCCUAGUUUAAAUUCUUUAUUUUCAGAUUGUUCUGGACUGAAAAUAAAGAAUUUAAACUAGGCUAGAGAUGCCUUUAAGUUACAUUUCAGAUCCUCUUCACAGCACGCUACAUAUCUAAAGCCCUUGAGAUCCUGAUUGUUCUCACAGUUGUUGGUGGAAUCCAUAGUUUUAUAACUCACCUCUUUUUAUGGUGGCAUUGUUAGCCCUUCUGUGUCUCUCCCUAGGAUUUUUAAUUCAGGACUAAAAUCACAGAAGUAGCAAGGAAAGGCUCAAGACUAGAGAUAGCUUUCAAUCUCUUCAGAAAUAGCCUGGUGCAGUGAGAAAACUAGGUUUGUUUUCAGGCCAGUCUGAUCUUCAUCCUAUUCUGUCUAUAACUAGUUGCAGGUCCUUGCUCGGAUGGCAUAAUUUUUUGAUGCCUCCAUUUGCUUAACUAGAAACUAGGAUUCAUAUACACACUCUGCACUUUGUAUUGAAGAUUAAUGAUAAUGUAGGUUUUGGUUGCUGUGGCUGAGCCUGGCCAGUAAUAGGUGCAUAACAGAAGUAGCUAAGAGCAUUUCAUAAUCAGGAUGAACUCUCCAGGACAGCCCUACAAAGAAGGAGCUGUUUGUUCCCGGAUGGCCUCGACCUUCCAGGCUUGAUUGUAAAGAGUUUAGUGUCCUCUCCUUCUCUCAUUCCCUGCAGUUCAUUUCCAAUAAACUGCAGUUAUUCAAGUUGAGCAAGUUCCGGAAUUUAGUGCCUACCAUGCUAUUGGGCAGUUUAUUUAUAAUGUGCUUUAUGAUGAUACUUCAGAGAAAUUUAAUUGCUAUACAAAAAGACGAAUCAUUGUGACUUUUCGUUAAGGAGGCGAUUGCAAUUCUUUGCUCCCUGCCUGGUGUCUGGGUUAGAAGGCCCUUCUGCAGGCUGGUAGUGUCUGUUCCACCUGGAUUAGGUUAACUCAACAGGUAAUUCCUAUCUGUUUAUACACAGAUGCUUUAGCGCUUGCUGUACAAAGUCAUUUGGCUACACACUGAGGAGGCCCAUGGGAGUAGUAGCCUCCUCAAAUAAUGUUCCCUACCUAUCUGUCAAUACCUUCCAUCUUAGGUAUUGAGAAUUUAAUGAGGCUGUGUUUUCUUGGCUGUGCUUCUUGAUGUUGGAAGCCAUGUUCCUGGGGAACAAAUCUGUAUUCUUUUCUCCUAAGAUGUGAGUUUUUUUCAACCUUUGCUAAUAUUUUAAUGGAGCAAAUGUACAGAUGUUGAGAUUUUGCACUGCUUAUAAAAUGCCUACCAUGUUUUUUGCAUAAUGGAUUGUAUAGAAAUGCAGAUUAUAUUCUUACAGCAAAUAAAAAGAUGCUUUUAACAGA